ACUAGAUCAUCAUUCCUUAUAUGUCAUCAAUAGGCUUUUAAUCAGGUGUCAUCCACUGUUACUUUUUUGCAACACAUCCACCACUUUUCCAUCAGCCCCCACCGGUCUCUACUCAAUGUAAUAUAUCUAGAGCCCUACGUGGAUAUAUUAUAUUGUUUUUUGCAGACAACCCUCAAAUCCCUUUCUCUAGCCUUUGCCUCUAUCCCGAACUUCAGGCAUGUCCACUGGAUGUUCCUACAUGGACGACCCAGAAAUUUCUCAAACGUGACAUACCUCAAACCAAAACUAUCAUCUUUCACUCUCCUGUCAAACUCCCUUCUAGGUAACAGACGAAUGUUUUAUCUAUUAACACAAGCCAGAAAACUAACGCUCCGGCUCUGUCCCUGCCUAUCUCUCAAAGUUCGUUUUACCCACAGCUUGCAAAUUUUUAUUCCUCUUUUUAUGCCCUCUUCCUUUGUCCUAGUCAGAUCUUAUCCUGUUUCUAGAUUACAGCAAUAUCUUCUACAGUUGGGCUCUCAGUCAUCAGCUUCUAACUCUCCACUUUACAAUUUUAUUUUAUUUUAUUUUAUUUCAUUUUAUUUUGAGACAGAGUCUCACUCUGUUGCCAGGCUGGAAUGCAGUGGCACAAUCUGGGCUCACUGCAGCCUCUGCCUCCCAGGUUCAAGCGAUUCUCCUGCCUCAGCCUCCCAAGUAGCUGGGACUACAGGCACACAACACCACGCUCAGCUAAUUUUUGUAUUUUUAGCAGAAAUGGGGUUUCACCAUGUUGGCCAGUAUGGUCUCAAUCUCCUGACCUUGUGAUCUGCCUACCUCGACCUCCCAAAGUGCUGGGAUUACAGGCAUGAGCCACCACGCCCAGCCUUACAGUUUAUUUUUGGCCAGAGCUAUUUUACUUAAUAGAGGUGGUGAUCAUGUCAUUUGCCUGCUCAAAAAUCCUUGAUUAGAUCCUAUGACUAUCAGGAUAUGACUGAAACUUCAUAGCCUGACAUCCAAUACUUUUUCAUCUGUGCCCACUGCUCUUUACUCAAUAUAAUAUAUCCAGGGCCCCACGUGGAGCCUAACAUACUGCAGAGGCCUGAUAAAUAAAUGAAUAAAUAAACAAAUGAAUGAUGGAGUGGAUAAAUGAAUAAAUGACUCACUAGGCAUUGAGCCUGCCAAACAGAUGCAUGCAUCAUGCUGCCAAGAAAGCUAUUUCCCUCCUUCUGAUAUAGGUGAAAUCCUAUUCAAUAUGUCAUUGUUUUUUCAGUUUUUUUAGACUAUUCCAGUCUCAAUCAAUUGCUUCUCAACUUGUGAUUCUGAGACAUUUUAUUCAUGCUACAGUUGUAGCAGUUAAUAUAUGUCAAGGUUAUUUAUAUGUGUGUUGGGUGUUCACAGAGACAGGGACUCUUGAUGGCAAUGAAGACUCAGCUACUAGCAAAAAGCCUGAUGCUCUUCGGAAAUCAAUCCAUGUUUGAAUUCCCACCACCACUAAUUUCUUUCAGUCAUAUUAUGUCUUUCCUGAAGUCCUGCAAUAGCUUUAUAAGUGUUUUCCCUACCUCCAUUCUCAUCCUAAAAUCUCCUCCUCAUUGUCCUACUAGACAAAUCCUUUUGUUCUGAAAAUGAAAAGUUUGCAGAAAUGCCAGAGCACUGAUGAAAUUAGAGGUCAGGAUUCCUGAUUUAGAGGUCAUUGCCUUCCUAAAUGCAUCUGAAGUUUCCACCUUUUUUGGUGACUAAAGUUGUUUUAGAGUUUUAGGCACCCUGGGUUGCGAAAUAAAUAGAAUAUCAUUUUGUGGGGGUAGUAGAGAUCUUUCUGUAAGUUUUUAGCUGCUUAGCCAUUUCACAUUAUUUGUACUUUGUGAGUAAAUAUAGAUUCAGGAAGAAAUGUUCCUGGGAACAGGAAGGAGACAUAUCUAAGCCCGAAGUGAACUUAAUGACUUUGUGUUUUCCCUGCUAACAGGAGUCUUGGAACCCACCUGGGUUGUAUCAAAUAAAUACAAUUAUUGCAGUUCAACUAGGUCAUGUUUGUGCACACACAAAGUUUGGAUGUGGCAGAAGUAAAUGACUGGACAUUGUUAACAGAGCUGUGGUUUGCAAAACAGCAAAGGUUUUCAGACUGGAGAAAGGGAGUGAGUUCAGAGAAACAUCAGUCUAACCAAAGUGUUUCUGCUGCUGCUGCAGAUGCCACUGUUAAUUGGAAUUGCUUAUUACUUCAGUUACUUUCAACAGUGCUUUGGGGGAUACUCUUGCCCUCAUAUUGUCUAAAUCUGUCCCUGUCACUAGUGACUGGAUAACCCAGGGCAUUUUAACAGGCAUCCUAUUACCUGACAGUAGGCAUCCAGCUUCCUGUAUUAAAAGUAGAUAUUUCUCCUGGGAUUUAACCUUCUGUUCAAAGCUUGAACCACUUUGUUAGGAAAAAUGUGGUCCUAAUAAUGUUUUCCAGUCACCUGUGGCUUGCAAAGUACUUAAUGCUUAUGAACUCAUUAAUCCUCUUCAUGAAGCCAGUGAGGAAGGUAGAUGUCAAGUUAUGUUUUCCUCUUUCUAAGGGCUGUGAAUCUGAAGCACAGACUUGCACAGACUGUUUGGGACAUAUCCAUGGCAAAUUGGGAGAAAGGGGCCUAUCGUUUUGAGAUGUUCAAACCCAAAAUCUAGCGGCUGAUUUUUUAAAAAUUGUAACUUCAAGGUGGCUCUCCUCUCUAUAGCUAUCAAUCAGAAAUCCUCAGUGGGUAAAUCUAGCAGGAGGCAUUGGCUGAAAAAUGGAGCUUUGAGAGCAAUAACAUCUGCUCAGUUGGGUGGGGAACAGAUACUUGUAGUGUCAAGAUUGUGAUGCAUGGUCUUGGGAUUUUUCCAAGUUCAACAUGUUUGUCAGUCUUUUGAGGCCCCUAUUUAUCCAUGGUGUAAGGAUUUGUUUAACCAACUAUUUCCUCCUAAUCCUUGCAAAAACAUGUAUGAAGUACACAACAGCAGUUGAAACCAUAGUAGCAAUUCUUUCAAAGGACCCAGUCUAUGGCUCCUGGAAAGUUCUGUCCUUCCCCGUUCUAAAUCUAGUGGUAGAAAUGUAUCCUAGUUGAAGAUUGGUAUUAGAUGCUUACUAUUAAAACUGGAAUGUUAAUUCUUACUUCUAAUUAAAAGGCCUCAUUUCUGUUCCUUAGAUCUAUUGGUGAGGUGAUUUUUUGGGUUCUGGCCAACCAUAGAGGGGAACUUUAAUCUGCACGCUUCUUAGAGAACCCUGUUGCCACCUUAUUAUUUUCCCAAUGAAGUAUGCAGAGCCCAAGGACAUGUAGAUUGUUUAUUCAUCCAUGUGUGCACUUAUUCAUUUAGGAAGUACUUUUUCAUUAUUCACCAUGUGAAAACCAUGUGCCAAGCUCCUGGGGGUACUGAUAUGACCAGGCUUAUGAGGGGGAAGCAGGUGGGCCAUUUAGCAGGAGGCCUUGUAUUCAUAAAAGGCCUCACAUUAAGACUCUUGACAUUGUUCCCAAACGAAGUUUUAUUUUGGUUGUAAAUAAGGGUCAUUUGCAAAAUACAAGCAUUUACAAAUAUGUGAGAGUUUUGGUAAUCCUGCUCUGGCAUUUCAUAACAUCAUAACGUGUCCACAGGUCUCAAAAGUGGAAGUGACCUGGGCUGGUUAGAACCUCUUGGAGUCUGUAGAAAUGGCUCAGGCACCCUCCUUGUGUCUCAUUACUCUGUAGGAGUCAGGCAUCCUUCUCCCCAAGAAACAAUGUAGGUGGUAACCCAGGAUAAGAAAACAUCUGGAAGCAGCCAUGGAAUAUAAAUGUUAGAUAGCUGGAAGAAGCCACAGAGAGCCUUCAGUGUUUAUGUGUCAGUCAAGGAAACUGACCUGAAAGAGGUGCAGGGGGACAUCCCUAAGACCCACUGGCAGUUCACGGCACAGUGAGACUAGAAUGGAGGAUUGGUAAUCUGAGGAGCUCUGCUGUUUCUUCCAUAGAAUUGGGCCCUUGAUAAACACACAUGUGCAUGUGUCUUUAUAGCAGCAUGAUUUAUAAUCCUUUGGGUAUAUACCCAGUAAUGGGAUGGCUGGGUCAAAUGGAAUUUCUAGUUCUAGAUCUUUGAGGAAUUGCCACACUGUCUUCCACAAUGGUUGAACUAGUUUACAGUUAAUGGGUGCAGCACACCAACAUGGCACAUGUAUACAUUUUUAUGUAGCAAACCUGCACGUUGUGCACAUGUACCCUAGAACUUAAAGUAUAAUAAUAAUAAUAAAAAAAGAACCGGGCCCUUGACAAAAGAAUGGCACUUAGACUGUGCUUUACCCUGUUACAUGGUCCUCUGCACCACUCCCUAGGCAUGGGCUGAUGUCAGCUUCUUUCUGUUCCUUCCUUCUUUCCUUCUUUCCUUCCUUCCUUCCUUCCUUCCUUCCUUCCUUCCUUCCUUCCUUCCUUGUCUCCUUCCCUCCCUCCUUCCUUCCUUCCUCCCUCCCUCCUUACUUCCUUCCUUUCUUUCCUUCCUUCCUUCUUUCAUUCUUUCUUUCGUUCUUCCUUUCUCUGUCUACCCCCAUCCUCAUCGCUCUCUUUUUUUCUUUCUCUGUCUUUUAAAUUGAGUGCAUCCUGGUUUUAUACUUACUGCUAGUAUCUUUUUGCUAUACUCCUCCUUUGUUCCUACCAGCAAUGGAGGUUGGCCCACAUCAAAAGCAGAAAGUUUGGUUUUAAUCAGCACAAUAUUUGCAGUGUGAGCUUUGAUCUUGACUUCUGCCUGGGGCCAGAGCAGGACUUCACCGCAACAGUGAACUCAAGUCCCCGUGUUCUCCUCUCUGAAGCUGGGAUCACCAGGAUGUGGUUAGUAUGUUGCGGAAUGAAUGUCGCUGGGAUUCAAAGCCUGCAAUGAGUUUUUUCGGUAAGUCCCAACUAUAUGAGAAAGAGAGCGAGAGGGAAAAAACCCAUACAAAGCAAGCAUCUCCCUUCUCCCCUCAAAACACAAAGAAGACAAACUAGGCCAGAUUGACUAUUUUCCUGUUUCAUCCUGUUCUUAUUCCUCUUCUUUGAGUUUUAGACAAGUAUGUUAUGACAAAAAUUUAACUCCAUAUUUUCCCUGAAGUCUCUAAAUUCUUUGAGCCGCCUCAUAGAUAGUACUUCUCAAUGUGCCAAAGACUUCAAACAAGCCCGAACUUAACAUUUUCCCCUAGAAACCUGCUCUUCUGGCCGGGCGUGGUGGCUCAUGCCUGUAAUCUCAGCACUUGGGGAGGCUGAGGCAGGUGGAUCACUUGAGGUCAGGAGUUUGAGACCAGCCUGGCCAACAUGGUGAAACCCCAUCUCUACCAAAAAUACAAAAAUUAGCAGGGCGUGGUGGUGGGUGCCUGUAGUUCCAGCUACUUGGGAGGUUGAGGCAGGAGAAUGGUUUGAACCCAGAGGCAGAGGUCACAGUGAGCCGAGGUUGUGCCACUGUACUCCAGCCUGGGUGACAGAGCGAGACCCAUCUCAAAACAAACAAACAAACAAACAAACAAGCAAACAAACCAACAAACCCUCCUCUUCUUUGGUUUUUGUAAUCUGCCACCAGGCUCCCAAGCUAGAAACCUUGAAUUCACCUUACACUCCUCUCUCAUUCACCACAUUCUGUCAAUUCUGCCACCUAAACGAAUCCAAUUACUGCCUUCCCUCCACUCCGUAUGCCACACAGCUGCCAGGGAGAUCUGUCUAAAAUGCAAAUCUGAUAGUACCAUCCUCCUCCUUAAAAAGCUCUGUGCAUUCCCUAGACUCAGAGUCACACAUGCACACUCUUAAGCAUGAGAUAGCCACAUGGCCCUGGCUGCAGCUCAGUGAGGUAGCCCUGCUGCAGCCACACUGGAUGUCUGACCACACCUUCAUGGGGUGUGCUCAUGAAUGCCUCUGCAUCUUUUCUCCAGUUAAUCACACCACCUGCAAUAUUCUUUCUCAACUGGUCACAUUCUGUUCUUUCUUCUAGAUUCAGCUCACUCUCUCCACAUUUAAGUCUUCCAAGGCCUCUCAGGUAGUUGGUUGCAUCAUCCUCCCACUUGGAUUUGAUUUACUGGAAGGAACAUCGGCUUUGGAGUUUCACAAACAAAACUUAAGAACCUGUUCCACUCUGAAUGUCAUUGCUUCAACCAUAACACAGACACAGUGCCAGCUUCACAGAACUAUUGAGGGAAUUAAACAAAGAAGCACUUGGUUUCCGAUAAAUAUUAGUUUCCUUUCUAUAGCAAAUUUUACAUAGAAAAUUGCAUGGUGGUUAAAAGUCUAUAGCCCUGAAUCCAGAAGAUGUGGCUUUAAAGCCUAGCUCCACCACAUACUUAUGUGAGUGACCUUGAACGAUUACAUUUGCUUGAGCAAAUUAUUCUCCUUUCAAUGUCCUUAUCUCUAUAAUAAUAGUACCUACUUGAUAGGGUGCUUGGGAAUAUUAAAUGAGAUAAAUAUAAGGUUAUUGUAUUUGGCACACAAUAAUCACACAGUGGGUUUGGGCGGUAAUCUUUUUUUUCCCAUACUUGCCCUGCUGUAUCAUAAUUAUUUGUUUACACAUUUUUUUCCCUAUUAACUUAGGGAUUCCUAAAAGGACCAGAUGGUGCCUUACUCAUACUUGUAUCCUCAGGGGCUACCAUGGAACACAGUGUAAAUGUUCGGAAGUUACUUCUUCAAAUGGAUAAGGCCUGGUACGUUUCAUCUGAAGUUUCACUUCUGGACUGUGGUCAGCCACACAAUCUGGAAUUCUUCCAGGGUACUGCUCCAUGCUCACAUCCAUGCCAAUCUCUCUUUAUUUUUAUUAUUUAUGUAUUUAUUUGUAAUAGAGAUGGGGUCUCACUGUGUUGCUCAGGCUGGUCCCAAACUCUGGGCUUAAACAAUUUUUCCUACCUCAGCUUUCCAAAGUGCUGAGAUUACAGACAUGAACCAUCAUGCCCGGCCUCAAUCUCUCUUUAAAACCCACUUCAAAAUAGGCUUCUCUAAGAAGAUUUCCUCCAUAUUACCCCAAGUUCAUUCAGAGCUCUCUUUUAAAUCUCAGUUCCAGUUGCCUUGCUGAUUUUUUAAAAUUAUUAUUUCACACGUAUGUCCUCAGUGGGCUUUUUUUUCAGUUCUUAAAUUAUUUCAUUUGUUUAUUUUUAAUUUUAAUUUUGGGGGCUACAUAGUUGACAUGUAAAUGAUAGGGGACUGGACUACCUCCCUCCUGUGAUCUGUGAGUGAUCUUGCUGCCACCAACAGUAGCACACUUGUUGUGGGGGCUUUCAUUGAAUAGUGUGUUACCUGGUCGGGUUGCCUCUCAUGGCAGCAUCUUUUUUCCCCAUCUUCUUUUCUUUUUCUUCUCUUUCUGUUCUCUCCAAGGGCCCCUCCAGCCUUGAAUGAGUGUUGUGAUCCCUGUUUUAGACUAGAGGAACUUCCAUUUCUGCCCUGGAUGCCAGAGUCCAUCAAUUUAAAACCUGUUCUCUCCUCUUUCCUAUCUGUGGCAGGUAUAUACAGUGUGGGUUGUUCCUCACCCUUCUCAUUUCAGCUUAGUUGACUCCAGUGGUAUUGGAUGCCAGGAAACAUUUAUCCUCCUCCUUUGCUUGUUUAUUUUACACACAUACACAAACACACACACAUUUUAAAAGUGUGCCCCUGGCUGGGCAUGGUGGCUCACACCUGUAAUCCUAGCACUUUUGGAGGCCUAGGUGGGUGGAUCACUUGAGGUCAGGAGUUUGAGACUAGCCUGGCCAACAUGGUAAAACCCCGUCUCUACUAAAAAUAGAAAUAAUUAGCUGGGUGUGGUGGUGCGCACCUAUAAUCCUAGUUACUCAGGAGGCUGAGGCAAGAGAAUGCUUUGAACCUGGGAGGCAGAGGGUGCAGUGAGCCGAGAUCACGCCACUGCACUCCAGCCUAGGCGGCAUAGUGAGACUCUGUCUCAAAAAAAAAAAAAGAAGAAAAAAUUGUGUGACCCUAACCCCAUAUGUGAGAGACAAUCUACAGGGUUCUGGAGAGGACAGAUAUAAAACAGAUACAGGUCGGUGCAGUGGCUCAUGCCUGUAAUCCCAGCACUUUGGGAACCCGAGGCAGGUGGAUCACUUGAGGUCAGGAGUUCGAACCAGCCUGGCCAACAUGGUGAAACCUUGUCUCUACUAAAAAUACAAAAAUUAGCCGGGUGUGGUGGCACAUGCCUGUAGACCCAGUUACUUGGGAGGCUGAGGCAGGAGGGUCGCUUGAGCCCGGGAGGUGGAGGUGGUUGUGAGCCAAGUGCGUGCCACUGCACUCCAGCCUGGGCAAGGGGAGUGAAACCUUGUCUCAAAACAAAUAAAUACAUAAAUAAUAAAUAAAUAAAAUAAAAUAAAACAGAUACAAAAUGUGUUGAAACACUGUUAACAGAAUUCUUAAGAGCAGUAUAUUUUAGAUUUCAGUUAGUAGGGCUAAGUUAUAUUAUAAAGAGGCUCAGAGAGCUUGAUGUAAAUUAAAGCUCUCUGUUUGGGUUUAAGUUUCAAAAAAAAAAAAAGAGGCAUGGUUUCGUUUUGUUUUAAGCAUGUUUUUCUAUUGUCUUCAUGUCACACCCUCGAGCUGAAGUGAUUUUUGAUUAGGGAGAAGACAGAAACCAAUUAAGGGCUUCUCCAGUCCAAAUGGAGUGACUACUAGAAGAAAGCUGUAAACGUACUACACUUGCAUUUCACAAUCUUAAUGCAUUUGUUUUCUUAGCGAAGAAAUUUAAACACUUGUGAUGCAAUGGAACAGAAAUUUUUUAUACGUUUUUCCUAAAUCUGUCUUUUUCUUCAUUUUCACAUGGAAACAGAAAUUUGUCAGGUGCAUUUUUCUUCAGAAUAAUUAUUUUUCUGCUCUUCAGAUGACAGAAAUGGUAGAAAUGAAAAGAGAACACACCACCUAGCAUUUUCUUCCAUUUUAUAAAUUUGGAUCUUUUAUCUCAUUCUCUGGAUUCAGAGAUUCUAAUUAUUGUCUGGGUACCUGGACCUUUCUCUUUUCCCAAAACCUUGUUCACCUCCCUCUGGGACAGAGCAGUUUCCCUUCCUGGGGAUACACAGCUGCUAGUUUUAUUCUGUUCCGCCCACAAAUCCAGUGUUGCUGCAUCUCUAAAGUCUCUUUGAUCUCCUCCCACGUAGUGAUAUUUUACCCUUCCAUUGAGUGACCAACCUCCUGGGUAAAAAAUGACAAUCCAGGAAAUAGAUGAUCCAAAGCGACUCUUCUUGCUAUAGUAUUCUGAGAUCAUUAUUUCACACCUCUACCCAUUCCCUAGCCUAAUUAAAAUGUCUGUAAACAUGGGACCAGACAUAAACUGCAUAAGAAAAUAAGCACAGACCAUUGAAAUUAGAUGGUUCCAUCAUUAAAGGUCUGUACUUUUUAAAAAUUUUUUUUUGAGACAGAGUUUUGCUCUUGUUGCCCAGGCUGGAGUGCAAUGCCACAAUCUCGGCUCACUGCAACCUCUGCUUCCUGGGUUCAAGUGAUUCUUCUGCCUCAGCCUCCUGAGUAGCUAGGAUUACCGGCGCCUGCCAUCACACCCAGCUAAUUUUUGUAUUUUUAGUAAAGACAGGGUUUCACCAGUGUUGGCCAGGCUGGUCUCAAACUCCUGACCUCAAAUGAUCUGCCCGCCCUGGUCUCCCAAAGUGCUGGGAUUACAGGUGUGAGCCACUGCACCCGGCGUAAAGGUGUGUACUUUCAAAGAUACCUCUCUCAAACCAUAUUUAUAUUCUCCUUUUUAACAUUGGAGACCAAAUUUCUGUAAGAUCUGGUUUUCAGAUAAGCACUUGAAAUAAGGCAAAAAAAAAAAAAAUGCUUUAUUACUAGACCUAGCUCAUAUCUUAAGGAGAGAGGUGGAUGUCGUCUGUAGGGAAUGUGAAGCCAAGGAAAGGAUCCACACUGACCUCACUUCCUGCAAAGUGGAUGGUGGUGGUUUCUCUUGUUACUUUGUAUCAGUUCCUCCACCAGCAUCAAUAUUUGUUGGGAGGAAAAGCCACCUGGCAAUGUAGGAUCAACAAAUAGGAGAAGGCAUCACAGUCAUGACUACUGUGGAGUCAGAUGUUGAAGUAGCUAUCAGCAUAAACUGGUAGGAAGAGAUGCAUUUCCUGAUAGAAAAGACAGCUAGGAUGCAUACAAAUGUUUCCCAGAAAAUAUAGUGGCUGGUUACAAGCAACUCCCAUUGAUUAGUAAGAGAAGAACUACGUGUAGCAGAGAGAACUCUGAGCUAAGAGUUCAACCCUGUUUUUGUUCUUGACCCUGUCCAACAGCAAACUUGUUUUUGAGUUUGAGUAAAUCACAUAAUAAUAUUAUGUAUUGGGCAUACAGUGAGCAUUCUUUAGGCAUUGUGUAUAUGCUGAUCAUCUAUUGUGUAGGAAACCAUCCAAAGCUUCAUAACUUUAAAAAAGUAUUCUUUCUUACCAUUCUGGGGAUUAAUGUGCACAGCUGAGCAGCUCUUUUUGGGAUACCUCCGUAUGGUUGCAAUUAAAUUGUCAGUCGUUGGAAGGCUCUACUCACCUGACUGCAACCCCUAGGCUGAGAUGGCUGGAUCAGUUGAGGAUUCUUGGAGCAGCUCCCUCUGUACAGUGUCUCCAUGUGGUUGACCUGGGCUUCCUCCAGCAUGGUGAUCUCAGAUAGUGAGACUUCUUACAUAGCUGCUGGCACCACCGCCCCCCCAACCCAGAAUGAGCAUCCAGGAGACAGGAAGUGGAAGCUGCUAGUCUCUGAAAGUCUGGGCCUAGAAACUGGAGCAACAUCAUUUCUGCCAUGUGCUCCACUGGUCAAAGCAGUCUCAGAGCUCCUCCAGAUUAAAGAAGAGGAGAAAUUGACUCACUUGUCAAUAGGAGGAGUGUCAAAGCAGGUGCGGUCAUAUUUACUAUGUUACUUAAUACUUCUGGAAAAGGUUCUGACUGGGUUCCUCUUGUCCAGAAAUCUGCUUGAAAAAAGGAUAUAAGGAACUAUUGCCAAAUGAUGAUCAAAAUAAUCAACUCUAUUGGUGCUAAAACUGUGCCAAAAGCCACACUUCCUCCAGCUGAAAUGGGGGCUUGUUCUACCCCUUUUGCCCUGAAUUUCAAAUAGAGGGACCCUGGGUCUAAACUGGCUGAUCCACACCGUCAGAUGCCUUGUCUGGAACUGAGAGAGAAGACGCCUGGCUGGACCUGCCAGGUGAGGCAAACAGGUCUAUGUCCACAGGCCAAGAGAGAGGCUGGGAGUCUGUCGUUCUUUUAAGGCACCCACUGGUAGUGUGCAUCAGUCUGAUUAGUAGUAGCCUCUCCACCUGUGGUGGGGAGCCACUGAGAUGGACCUGAAUUUUCUUUCAGUCUUGCCCUUUCCUAAGAAGUAGAUCAAGUCUCUGUCUCUUCUAAAAAUGUGAGGAGGGCAGGGAUGCAUCAGGCAUUUUCUUCUUCCCCAUACCAUCCAAAACUCCAGGAUUAUUGGCCAUCUUUUGCAGAGAAGAAAACUGAGGCUCGGAAUAGAUUCACCACGUUUCCAGAGUAACAAGCUGAUAAGGACUUGAAGCACAUUCACAGGACGUCAUCCUCUCUCUCUUUCAACAUCUCAAAAAUCAAACAAAUAUAUGUGUGGCAAAUCUUACUACCUCCCCAACACACUACUCCCAAGACCCACCCCUACUUAUUUCUCUCCAUAUCCCUUAUUACAUUAGCAUCUUGCAUAGUGUAUGUGUACUCAUUCAUGUGUUUGCUGUCUGCCCCUCCUCCCACUGUAAUUGGAUCAAAUAUAAAUGAUAUCAUUGGAAUAUGGAAGAGGUACCAAUGUAGCUAGUGUUAUUUGCACACACGAUUUACCAUUGUGUACCAAAUAAUACUCAGUUAAUACCUGCUGCCUUUAGAAUGUCCCCUUUAUAAAGCUCUGAAGAUAUGGGCUGCCAUGCACCAAUCACUACUGGCUGUAGGGUACUCGCACAUGGCUGAAGUUCUAGUGCUGGUGUUGAUUCGCUGGGACUUGAACAGCAUGAGGUCAAUGCAUUCCAUAGGAGACUGCGGUAACAUCAUGUACAGGUGGGAUAAGUUUCUUUUCCAGGUAAGAUGUUCCUGGCUUAGCUGCUGUUUUCUGUGACAAGUUUUGUGGACAGAAUCAACUGCCUGCCUUUCCAGCAGUGCACUUAGAACCUCAAAAAAACUGGCUCUUGGGCAGAUCAACAAACCAAUUGAAUGCAGUUGCAAUUUUAAAAUCUGAGCCACAGAAAGAUAUUGUUGCUUGGCUAGGUUGUGACUAUCUUCCCUGGAUAAUCCCUGCAGGACUUUUGAGGGAAGUAAAGAAGUGGCAUCUCCCAUUUCAUCCAUCAGAAUCAUCAUUUAGGAAUUAUCAAGAAUGAGAGAGGGUUAGUCUUGGAAUGUGCAGAAAGGUAUACAUGGCAGUUACCAGUAUAUUAAUAAAAAUGCCACUGUGCUGAAGAAACAACCGAGCAUAAUAAAAGACUACUAUCGAAAGAACUUUUGAUUGUGGCACUCUUGCAAUGGCUUUAGGUGUCUGAUUGCAUUUAAGGCUCAGAACAAUCCUCUAAGGAACGAUAAUCUCCAUUUCACAGAUGAGGAGGAAGAAGAACAAAGAGGCUAAGUGAUUUGCCCAAGGUCUCACAGUAAUGAGUGUCAGAAUCCAGAUUUGAACCAAGACAGUCUGGCUGUAGAGCCUAUGUUCUAAACAGCUAUACCACUAGAUCCUUCUACUACCUUUUUGGUGUUUUGUUGUUAACAUUUUCAAGGUCUAAAGAGUGUAUAAGCAAGCCAACUAACUUGCAAGUUCUUUGUGUUAUUGAAAUAUAUAUGCAUGGUGUGUGUAUGAACACUUUAUAUACACUGUUGUACAAUUAUAAAGUACUUUGGAGUGGGAGGGGGUUUAGAAGUUUAUUUCAGCUUCCCACCCAAUGCAGGGGUCCCCAGAGAAUCAUCAUUCAGCUUUCCUUGAACUUUAAAAUCAGAUGAAUAAAAAUACUAAGGGUCAACAUAAGCGCUGAUGCUAAUAAUUGCUGUAACUAUGGAAACAAACUAGAAUACAGAGGACAAAAAAAGGUUCUUACGAGAGAAUUAAAAAAAGACAACUGAAAUUCACCAUACACACACAAGGUAGUGACUAGGCUUGGGAACCAAAAUAAAUUAAUAAAGACUGGAAAAUGGAGGAGAGUAGGAUGAGAGAAGUGUAAGCACUAGAUUUCUGGCCAUCUGUAAAACAUAGUUAAACUCUUUGUUUUGAUUACAUAAAUAUUUUGUGUUUGUGAAAAAAACUCUGGGAUAAUCAUUCAUAUAAUUAGAAAUAAGAUGCCUGGCUUCUAAAUGGGCAUAGAAUAUAAAACAUAGCCUAUUUAGGAAAAGAAAUAGUGGAAGAGAAACAGUAAGAAAACAAAUGAACAACAGCAAUGAACCCCAAUGUGUAAGCUCCAUGGCAAAUACAUAGCUUUACAUUUUUCUAUUAAAACAUAAAAUAUACCAAAGUAGAUUUAACAAUGAUAUGCAGUGAUUUGCAUUCAUUACCUAAUGACUAAAAAUAUUCUAGCCAAUUAUAGCGCUAUACAGUAUUUUGUAGGUUAACAUCUUCUCUAAUUACUUGGAAGAUACACUAUGUCUUAUUCAAUUUGGUAUUGCCAAUAUAUAAUUGGCAUAUGAUUGGUGCUCAGAUUUAUGUUAAAUGACUUAAUGAAUUUUUAGAAAGUGAGUGGAUAACAAUAUAAGGAAAAUAGUAUUUAAAGAAAAAAUAUUAUAUAUAGGAGAGUGGGUGAUUAUAAAUGUAUAAUCAAUAGUGAAGACAUAAUGAAAUGGAAACUUUAUGUGCCAAAGAGCAUUGCUAUAAACCACUUGGGGCAAAAACUAUUGGAAAUACAAAGAUAAAUUGGUGGUAAGAGUGUGGGCUUUAUAAUCGGUCAUACCUGGAUUUGAAUCAUGGCUCUGAUAUUUAGUAGUUUGGCCAAUUAUUUAUCCUUUCUGAAUCUUAUUUUCAUCAUCUACAAAAAUGAGACUAACCUCAUUGUGAGGAUUAAGUGAGGAAAUGUAGGUAAAAGUGAAGGAGGGAGAGAUGUAUCCUGUUCUCAGUGGUUAUGCAGCAUUUGGUCAAUAAAUAUCCCCAGAGUGAGAACCCUCUUCUUGUCAUUUUCACAGUUCUUUAGUGCCAGUAUAAUGCCUUGUUCUAUUAAACAUUCAAAUGGCUGCUGAGUACUGAAUAAUUUUAAAAAGAAGAGUGCCGUAAACUGUUUCCUUGCUUAAAAACAGAAAUCUAACUGUAGUGGCUUUACAAAUUAGGGGUUUGUUUUCUUACAUAAAGCUGAGACAUAGGUGAUCAGGUGUGGCUCCAUGAAUUUAUGAAGGACACAACCCCCUUCUCUCCUUCAGUUCAACCAACCUUAGCACUUUCUUUCCAUGCUCCAGGUCACAGAAUGGCUUCUGAAACUCUAGCUAUCAUGGCCACUGCUGUGACUUGAAUGUGCUCCUUAAAAAAAGAAAAAAAAUGUGUUUUGUAAACUUAAUACCCAGUGCAACAGUGUUGGGAGGUGGGACCUAGUGGGUAGUGUUUAGGUCAUGAGGGCUUCAUCCUCAUAAAUGCAUUAAUGCCAAUUAUUAAAGGGCUCGAGGCUGUGAGUUCCAUUUCUUGCUCUCUUGCAUGCAUGCAUUUUUUGCCUGUCUGCCUCCCACCAUAGGAUGAUGCAGCAAAAAGGCCCUCACCAGAUGCCAGCACCUUGAUAUUGGACUUCUCAACCUCCAGAACCAUGAAAAAUAAGUGUCCUUUCUUAAAAGUCACCCAGCGUGUGAUAUACUUUUACAGAAGCACAAAAUGGACUCAGACAACCACAGUCUACGUUAUAGGAAGAGGAAGGGCAACAGUCAAGGACAUUUCUUCCACUUCACUUAUCUCUCUUCAAAAACUCUCCUGGAAUCCCUACCCACAAAUUCUACUUAUCUCUUAUACCAUCCAUUACUCCCUAUAAGGAAGACAGAGAAAUGUGAGUUUUUCAGUUUUUUUGGUUUGGUUUUGUUUUGUUUUUGAGACAGAGUCUUGAUCUGUCACCCAGGCUGGAGUGCCGUGGCAGGAUCUUGGCUCACUGCAAGCUCCGCCUCCCAGGUCCAAGCAAAUCUCAUGCCUCAGUUUCCUGAGUAGCUGGGACUACAGGUGCCUGCUGCCAUGCCCGGCUAAAUUUUUAUUUUUAGUAGUGAUGGGGUUUCACCUUGUUGGUCAGGCUGGUCUCAAACUCCUGACCUCAGGUGAUCCGCCCACCUCGGCCUCCUGGAGUGCUAGGAUUACAGGCAUGAGCCACUGCCCCCAGCUGUGAGUUUUUUUUUAAACUGGAAUAUAAAAUAGCCACUCCAUAUAAAAUAGAGUUUCUAAUGUUUGUGAAGAAAGAGAGAAUUGAUAUUAGGGAGGCAACAAAGAAUCUGUCAAAAUGAUUGAUGGUUUUCUUGGAUGGGAACUUCUUGCAUCACUUAUUAAAGUCUACACUUAUGUAUUUAAUAAUUUUAUGUCUAGUGGGUUUACUUCAGCUGAGCAGGGCCUGGGGUGGGGUCCUAAAGUAACUGAUGGAGCUUUCCUUUGUGAGUUUUAUCUGUUAUAUAUUCUCUGAGAGGUUGAAUUUAGAAAGUAGGGCAAUUGAAAAUGGCUAGGGAUUACUGAAGGGUAUUUAUUAAUUUAUUUGACUGGUAAUACAAACAUUAGAAAAAUCAACAGGGGCAAAAGAAAAAACAACUAAAAAGUAAUUUUUUCUUCACCCUUGGCUCUCAGUUAUUCAGCCCCUGUCUUUAGAAGUAACCACUGUGACUACCCACUAUUUAAAUUUUGUGUAGACUUCUGGAUAAAGUCACUGCUUAUAAUGCAUAUAUGGGUAUGUAAUCUAGUUUAUUUUUUUAAGCAAAUGAGACCGUAUCAGACAUACUUCUCUGCACAUGGAAUAUUUCACUUAAGAGUAUUUCUUGGAUAUCUUUCCAAGUCAUACUUGAGAAGCUGCCUCAUUGUUUUUAACAGCUGGCUAGUAUAUCAUUGCAUGGAUAUACCAUUAUUUAUUCUCUUGAUGAACUGUAUAUACCAUAAUUUAUUUGGCUGAACAUUUUGUAGAGUCCAAUAUUUUGCGCUAUAAGUAAGACUAUAAUGAAUAACCUUGGAAAUAUGUCAUUUUGUGUUUGUGUAAAAGUACUCCAAGAAUUAGAAUUUAUUCUGAGUCAAAAGGCAUUUGACCUUAUGACUUUGAGAACAUUGCCAAAUUACUCUCCAUAAGUAUUAUGGCAGUUUUUACUCCACUAACAGUGUUCUGAUGAUAUAUUUUUGCUCAUUACAUUGUGUGACCAAACACUUGGUCUUCUUUGGAAGGCCAAGGCAGGAGAAUCGUUUGACCCCAGGAGUUCAAGACCAGCCUGGACAACAUAACAAGACCCCAUCUCUAUAAAACAAACAAAUAUUUUGGUGUUUGCUCACAUAAUAAACAAAAAAAAAAUCAUAGGUUGAGUAUCAUAUUGUAAAUUUAAGAGCUAAAAAAAAUUUCUAUUUAUAUUCUUUGCCCAUUUUUCUCUUGGGUUGGUUAAUUCUUAUAGGUUGUCUUUAUAGUUUAAGGAAAUUAGCCUCUUAUUAGUUGCAAAUGUUUCCCAUUUGGUUUUUACUUUGUUUAUGGUAUUUUUCAUGCAGAAAAAAUUUUUUAACUGUUAUGUAGUCAAGUUUAUUGACUUUUAAAUGGCAUGCAGAUUUUACGUCAUAUGUAGAAAGUUUAAUAUCUCACAUUAAGAUUGUUUUAAUAGGUCAAUUUUUUCCUAGUUAGUUUUGUUUUUCCAAAGGGUAGCACAAAGACCAGUGUAACUACAAGCUACAAGGAAGCCAAUUUCAGCUUCUCCUGGAAGAAAGAACAUUUUAACAAUUAGUCUAACAAUGAAAUCAACCCCUUGUUGUAGUUUUCUUCAGGGUUUGGUAAGCUAACCAUUUUUAAGAGUAUUCCAGGAAGCCUGUAUUUCUUAUUUCUGCAGUCCUCUAUCUACUUUCCAAGAAGAAAUUUACUUUUCACAAUGGGCAUCAUUACCAGGCAGUUCUUGGAAAAUAAGCACAUAUAGUAAUGCGAUAUAUAAGAUUCAUGAUAUCUAUUAAUAAAUAGCAAAAGAAAUUUAAUGGAAAUCAUAUAAAUUGUUCUAGAGGAAGAAGUUUUUUGAGAUAGUUCAGUAUAGUGGUGAGAGACUGAGCUUGUGAGUCAGAAAGGCUAGUUCAGAUCCAAUUCUGUGCCUGGCUAUGAACCUCUGAGCCUCAGCUUCCCCAUCUUUAAAAUGGAGAUAGUAAUACUACCUACUACAUAGGAUUCUUGACAGGCACUCUUAAAAGUCUUAAAGUUCUAUGCAUUUUUUGAAAGUUUAAGUUUUCGAUAAAUAUUAGUUAUUUUGUUGUUACUCUAUUUGGAUGCAAUUCCAUUGCCUAGUAUUUUUUUUCUUUCGGCAAGCAUUUAUUGAGUGCACACUGUCUACUAAACACUGUACUGGAUUCUGGGGUAUAAACAAGAAUAAACAAGGUACCUGUUCCCAAAGACCAUAGCCUUAGGUUUUACAGAGGUAUGGAGGCAAGAUAUUAAUAAAAUUUACUUGUUAAAUCAAUAAGGCCCCAAAGCACCAUGCAUUUGUAAUCUAGAGUAUGAAUGGCACAUAUGGCAAAGUAACAUGUUGGCAACGAGCCUAUGAAUGAAUAGCAGCUGGAUUGCAAAAUCAAGGAGAAGCUUUUCCCCUACCCUCCGAACCCAAACAAUCCCCUUCUUUCAUCAGGUAACAAGAGAUGACAGCACAGGGAUCAGGUCCUAAUGCACAGCCUUUCAUGGCCCCAGUCCUGCUUUUCAUUCUGAUUAGAGGAUAAAGGAAAUGGGUUUCCUGGCUGGUCUCAUCCUGGUAAACAUUUUGCCUGCUUUGCAGAACCGCCACCCUAUUUAAGUGCAAUUUGCUGGACCUGCAGUUGGUUGAAAACAGCAGGGCCUUUGUCAGUGAAUAGAGCUGUAGUGACAGGGAGGACAUUUAUAAAAAUGCUGGUGUGUCUCAUGCCCCGUGCCAGCUGGUGCUAUUAGUGCUCUUUUAUGUGUGUCUUGAAAUAUACUGUAAUAAAUCUUUAAAGGAAAGCCAGGACAUAAUGAGUAAUCAAAUUCAGUCCUCUGGAAUUCAUUGCAAUGGUGGCUUCUAAACGUGGGUAUUGCCCCACCAGAAAUGGAAAACUGAGAAGUUAAGAAAAACAGGUUGUUCUUGAAAAUGUAUCAGAGACAUUUUUGGUAAAGAAUCAUAUUGGCCCUCUUCCAGUGGCUUUAUUUUUAUUAAGAACUAGAAAUCCAUGAGCUGAAAUACACAGACUGCUGGAACCCAGCCUUGAUGUGAAUCCUGCAUCUUAGUCUGAGUUACUAUUUUAAUAAAAAAGAAAUACUUCUAUUAAAAGUCUCUGGGUGCCCCAUCAAGUAUCCUAUAUCUAUUCAAUGUUAUAAUCGUAGAACUUGUACCAUAGUGUAAGAAAAUGUCUGGGAAGUGAUGACUGAAAAAAGCAGUUUUCUUCCAGCUGGCAUCUACCUGAUGAUCACCCCAUAUGUAUAUGGUCAAGGUGCGGAAGAGAUCUCUCCUAUUAAAAAUACUUGAUACAUUUGGGUAAUACAAUGUGUUCCAAGUUUUCUCUUUUUCUUUUUCAAUUUUAUGUGCUAUAGAAUAAUUUUAAAUGAUCAAAAAUAAAAGAACUGUGGUUAGGUAUGUAUGUCUACAGACCACCCAUUAUUCUCCCUUCUGGGCAAAGUCUAGAUCAAUUUUUCCAUUUGAGCCGGAGCUUCCUAUUUGCAACUAUAGAGAUUAGUGUUGAAUGCUCGGAGCUGCUAACAUAGGAGUUAACUAUGGCUUGUGGGUCAAUUCCAGCUUACCAUCUCUUGUUUGUUUAUUUGCCUAGAAGUUAGUCUGUGUUUAUUGUUUGCUGUAACUGUAGGUGUCAGAGGCUAAAAUUUCUGCUGGUGUCCUUGUUUUUAGGGGGUCCCUGUUGUCUUGGGUUUCCCUGGAGACUCCUUUAUAAAUAGAAUCUGAGCCUUGCAGUUCUUUUCAGCUAUCAUCCUCUGUUAUACGGGAAUCCUAUUGAUAUGGCGCUAAAAUGGAGGUGGUGGUAAUGGGGAAGCACCCAAUAACCCUAUGAUUUGCUCUCAGUCUUUAAUGACUCCAUCAUUAUAGAUUUAAGAACCUUUUAAUUCCUUUCCUUGUUUAUAGUCUUUGCUCAUUUUUCUGUCGGACUGCUUAACUUUUGCGUGUGUUCUUUAUAGUUUUAAGAAAUUAGCCUCUUGUUAGUUGUAAAUCUGUUUCCUAUUUGUCUUUUGACUUUGUUUACGGUAUUUUUUCAUGCAGAAAAAAUUUUAAAUAUCAAUAAAUUUUACUAUAUAAAAUUAUUCACAAGGUCUUCAGGGUUUUUUUCACCCCUUAGUAAAUGAGACAGGAAGGCUAGAUGGGGCUGGAGUUGGGUAUUUCCCUUUUUCCAGGUCAGAUGGGCUCUUUCUGAUAAAAUCUUACUAGGUUAGGCUCUGGUAAAAUAGUCUCCCUCAAAGACAGGUCGUGUUAAGGAGAACAGAACAGUCUGGGUGUAUUUAAAAAUGGUUACUUUUCCCCUCCCCUGCAGGAAGGAUGAGGGGAUUUUUCUUUGACCUUUACAGUGCAAACCUGGUUAAGCUUCAGCAGGUAAAACUCAUACAAAUGUGCCUCACCCACCUCUCUCAGGCUGGGUCUCCAGGAGUUUUUAAUUUCUGAAGCUAGGCCAGGCUCGGUCUCCAGUAAUUAGUAAAUUAUCCUUUAAAUAUGUCUACCCAAUGUUGGCUCCAGUGAGAUUUCUGCCCCAAGUAAGAUAUAAUUCUUUGUAUCUACCCCCUCUUCGGUUUUAGCAGUGGUGAUUUGAUCUGUAACCUCACUUCUCUGAUAGACCUAAGAAUUGUUGAUUUUCAGGGUUUUUUUUUUUUUUUUGGCUUGUUUCUUAUUGUGAGGACAGGAGUGACAAAUACCAUGAUCUUUAUUUACAGAACCAGAAACCAAAGUCUACCACCUGUGUUUGUAUAGCUUGUGAGCUAAGCAUGUUUUCAGGCAUUACCAAAUGAUUGAAAAAAUUUUAAAUAAUUUUUUGUGACAUGUAAAAAUUAUAUCAAAUUCAAUAUCAAACUUCAAUACUGUGUUCAUAAAAUUCUGUUAAAACAUGGCCAUUCUCAUUUGUUUAUGUAGUCUAUGGCAGAUUGAGUAUUUGUGACAGAGACUGUAUGGCCAACAAAACUUAAGUUAUUUAUCAUCUGGCCCUUUACAGAAAUGGCUGCUUUUUAGUACACUCUAGACAUAGGUCCUGGUUAAGUUUGAAUCCCUUGACACUGUGCUUGAGUUGAAAAUCAAAUGAUGGGCACCUGUCAAGGGCUGGAGAGGAUCCUCACAUUUAGAGAUGAGUGAAGACAUAGGCCUUCUCUCAAGGAGACUCUAGGCUUGUGGGGAACACUAGAGGGCCAACCAAAUAAGAAUUUAACGGAGUGGUUCAGAAUGAAAGGCUAUGAAGUUCGUCUUGGGCCACAGGAAGUCAUUGGAGCUCAUCCUAUUUGGUAGAACAGGAACUUCUUGAUGAUGAUCCAAGGGCUGGAUCUUUUUAGGAGUGCCAGGCUCAGGUGGACAUUGAUGUAUUGCGCUUCCUGAGAACUGAGAAGUUUCAGCUCCAAUCCUUCCAACAGUUAUGGCUGCUGUGGCCACUUCAGUACUGUAAUGCCACUUUCAAACACGCAUACUUUGUUCAUUGUGAUUUUUUUUAUUCUUCAGUUAUCAAGAAGUAUGCUAAUUUAAGGAAAGAGUGGACUCAUGUAUCAGAAAAGUAUUCAAAGCAAACCAUCAACCUAAUUUCAGAAAGUAGAGACCAGUGAGAGUUUCCUAAACAUUUAUAAAGGGUAGAAUGCUUGGACAUUUCUAGGUUGAUCGUGAACUCUGCCAGCAGUGUUCACCCACUUGCUUUGCCCUCUGAAGGUAUUUCAAGUAAAAGGAAAGAUAAACCACAAACUGUUUAGCUCAUGUAUGUCCUAUAAUACAUGUAUGUUAUUAUCUCUGUGGAGAAUAGGAGAACUUCAGAACUUUGUCUCUGGCCUGGAUGGAAAUUCUUUCAGUCCUUGUUGUUAUUAACAACAGCUAUAAGAUGUCAGAAAUGCCUCCUUAGCUAAAGUGGGUUGGGGCUGGGCAAGGUGGCUCAUGCCUGUAAUCCUUGCACUUUGGGAGGCUGAGGGUGGAGGAUUGCUUGAGCCCAGGAGUUCAAGACCAGCCUAGGCAACAUGGCAAGACACCGUCUCUAUAAAAUAAUAAUAAAUAAAUAAAUAAGUGGGUUGCUGCCAAGGAGGGUCCAUGCUGGACUUAGAUGAUAGGAUGGAUGCAGACAACAAGGAAAUAUACAAUAUGGAGUUCUUUAUUAAUUAAUCACAACUUCCCUGAGGUCCAGAUUCCUUAGGAAAGUUAGGUGACCACUCUUGGGCCCCCUGUGUAGGCCACAGUAUAUUAAGGUUUGCCUAGUCUGCAAUUGAGUAGUGUCCUUGAGUCUCUCUGGCUGUGUCCCCAAAUUGCAAUUCUGACUGUACACUAUGUUGUGGUUUGGCCUGGAAACAGGUAUAUUCCCUUGCCACCUUAUAUUUUUUAUCAGAGUGAUUGUGAAAUCCACCCAGCAGAUCUUGUCCAUGGGCCAUCAGUAUAUUACAUUGCAUAUUAAUGGAGCUGGAGAAAUAGUGAAGCAAAUAACCCAUGCAAAAGUAACUAAAGCACAAAUAAGGAACAUGAUAUUGACUCUCUUGAAUCUCUCACAGAGUAUAGAUUUGAUGAGGACCUCUAACUCAAUGUAAAGUCACCUUAAUGAAAUCUGUCUCUUAUUAUCAUCAUCCAGGCCCUUAUUGAAUAUGUCUGGAGGUGAGAAACUCAUAUCCUCCCCUCAACCCAUGUGUGUCAGUGUUAGACACUGCAUUAGUCAGGGAUCUUGGGUUUGCAAGUGACACAAUCAAUUUGUUUAAGCAAAAACAAUAUUUAUUAGCUCUCUUGACAAAAUUUGAGAAGUGCAAAUUUCAAGAGUGAAUAUAAAUAAGAUUUAAAUAUUGGAAAUCAAUAAUUAAUUUUUCAUCUUUUUCCCUCCUUCCUUUUCUCUAUGUAAAGCUAUUACAACAUCACCUGGAACAUAGUAAGUGCCCAAUAUGUGUUACUUGUUUUUACGUUUAUUACUUCAUAGGGUUAGCAGAAGCGAUAAAUGAGAUAAUGCAUUUAGCAUGGUUCCUGGUAUCACCACCAAUACCACUGCUGUUACUACUUUUCUUUCCAGUUUUCUCUGUUCUUCUCCUUUAAUCUUUCAGAGUGUCUUUCCCACUUAGCGAAAAACAUGGCCAUCACUAACUUCCAAGCUCACAUGUCCCUGCUUCACAAUUAGAAAACAUUUGGGAUGUCUUCUUUCUGUUUCUUAAGUUCCCCAUGGUAGGGAGAAAUCUGAUUAGCUUAACUUUAAUCCAGUGUCUAUACCUCUGUGGUCACAGUGGCCAGGAAGGAAAGAUACCCUCACUAGAACAUUACAGUUGGAAUAGAGGGAAGUUUUUCACAGAAGAAGGGAAGACUUGUUAAGCUGACACAACUAGAAACUGCUAGAGACAUCUGGGGUGAUUAGGAGUGCUUUCAUAAAUUUAAACUGAAUACUCGUGCUUCCUACUUUGAUCUUCUCCUGAAACACGAAAUGAAUCAGUUCUUUCUCAUUUGUGACCUUUCAGAUGUUUAAAUGCAGCUGUCAUGUCUGACUACUUGGCACAUUACAACAUUCUACUGACCCAGGUCUCCUGUCUCUGAGUUACCUUUUAUUCCAGUUUUCAGCUCUAACAGGACCCUUGUAGACUUCUUAUUUCCUCCUUUUCUUUAACCUCUGUAAUCACCUUGCCAUCUCUCACCCUGCUUUAGUCCACAGAGUUCCCCUUAAUCAUUGCUCAGCUGGCCUGGUUACUGCAGACCAAUCACCCAGUAUCAUGUAGGAAUGCAGUCCUUUCAGCAGCAAACAGGUUUGGGAAACCCGAUAGAUCUGUUUUGAUUCAUGUGUCUCUCCUACUGAGUAAAAGUAUGACCUUGAGAAAUUGACUCAGCCUCUUUCAGUGUUGUUGUAAGGAUUAGGGAUUAGUUAUGCACAGUCCUUAGCCCAAGGCCUGGCGUAUAGUAGAUGUACAAUAAACAGUAACUGUGGUUACUGUCAUUAUUAUUCUUAUAUCAAUUCCUGGCACCCCAAAGGAAAGGAAAAUGUGGUUAGAGAAUUUAUAUUCCAUCCCAUGCCCAUGGAGCAAAAGAUCAGGUUCUUCCUAUCCUGGCAAAGCCAGCAUGAAGAGGUGACUUGACCACAUGGGCAAAAAUUGGACCUUGGGACUUCAAUUUCUUUUUCUUGCAAGCCUCAGAUGUCAAUCCCAGCACUUAGGCCACUGGGAAUGUAGCAGUGGCUUUUCUCUUGUUUUCUACCUCCAGUUUUAAGCCAAUUGUCUUGAGGGAUAUAAAAAGCCCCAUUAUCCCAAGCUAGGGAAUUAGAACGUUAAUUCCAUCCAGGUCAGCUAUUAGAGGGUAUAAAGGCAGAGAUGACUCUUCUCUGGGGGCUUUACUGCAAGUGGUAGCUCAACUCAUUCAACUCCAUUGAAGAAACAUAGUUUUUAUAUUCUUACUCUGGCUAAAUGUCUUGGCAUUUGAGGUUCCCCAAAUUUUGGCUGUAGUCUACUUUUCCUUACUCUGUUGUACUCACCUUCUACCCAUCCAGAUCAGGUUAAUUCCCCCUCCCAAAGCCCACUCUGUGAAUAAGCACUUCUGAAUAUUUUAUCACAUCGUUACCCCAGUGAGUGUCCUGCAUCAAACUAAAUCCUACCCAUCUUUACCACCUUAGCUGUCCAUCCAUCGCUUUACACCUGUCCAUCCAUCCAUUGAAAAAAAUUGCUAUUUUAGGCAUUGAUACAGAUGUAAACAAGACCAAGUCCCUGGCCUCAUGGAAUGUACAUUCCAGUGUAAGAAACAGACAACAAAUAUAAAUAGAUGCUUUAAUGUCAGUUGUAUUAAGUGUAUUAAAAAUUAAAACAAAUAAGGAAAGAGAAAAUGAUGUUGGAGGUAGAAGGGUAGAGAUUGACUAUGUUGGAUAUGCUCAUUAUGGUUCACAGAAGGGAAGGUCAUCUUGUCCAGAAUGCUCCAAUGUAGGCAUCUCUUUCACAGUACCUCUGAAAGAUAGCAAUCCAUGGAGAUGAUGCACCGUUGAUCUUAAGAGUACAGACCCUGGAGCUGUAUUGACCUUGGUUUGAAUUCUAGCUCAACCACUUGCUGGAAUUCAGCUCAACAAUGUGACCUUGGUUGACUUAUUUACCAUCUUCGAGACUUCUUAUCCUUUAUCUGGCAAAUGGGGGUUAUAAUAGCACUAUUUCUUCCAGUUAUUGGUUGUUGGGAGAAUUAAAUGAAGUUAUGUCUGUAAAGCUAUUAGAACAUAACUUGGAACAUAGUACUUACUAUGUGUUACCUGUUGUUACCUUUAUUACCUCAUAGAGUUAGCGUAAGUAAUAGGUGAGAAAAUGCAUUUGGCAUAGUUCCUGGUAUCACUACCACCACCACCACUACUACUAUUAUAAUUGUUAUUUUUAUUAUUGUUUUCUAGUGACAGAAGACUUUUAAGAUGGGAAGUUCCUCGUCUUAUGAGUUUCCUUUUUUGACAGUCUGUUCAUUAAAUUGCCCCUUUUCACAUUGAACUCAAAUGUACUUCACAUAAAUAUUUAGUUUGUGGUCCCAGAUGGACCUGUCUACCAUAACCUCCAGAGCUAAGCAUCCAGCCCAAUAUAGUUUGGCUCUCCCUGAUCAUGACAGCCCAUGGCACACCCUCCUCCUCUGAAAUCCCCAAGCCACUUCUGUUAAUACCACUCACUUGGCCCUUACCAUUUAUUGUUCUGAUAGCUAUUGCCUUAUUAUGUUAGUGUUUAGUUCAAUCUACACCCAGAACAUAAGUGCUCUAGGGCAGGAUAUUGUCCUACCUUUUCUUUUUAUAAUCCCCUUGGAUGGAACCCUCUCUCUCUCUUUCUUCUCUCUCUCUCGCUCUCUCUCUCUCUCUCACACACACACACACACACACACACACACAACACCACAGCAUAGCUUAGACUCAACAUUUACGCACUGUGUCAAGGCCACUGUGUCACUACUGUGUGAAGGCCACUGCAACCACACUGGGUGACAUGAGAACCAACACCAUUGCCUCGGAUACAAAGGUUGCUUGUAUUUCACUGGAGCAUCUUUUAUUAUACCAGUUUCUUCCAUGUGCAAGUCAAAAUUGUGUCUUUUUUAAAUGUUCCUGCUGACUCAUAAUCUUGCUUGUCGUCUUUUCCUCCUCAUUUACAACUCUACAGUCCAUAAUGUAUUAAAUGAUGCAAGUUCCCAGCCUAAUAUUAGGGAAGGAAAGUAGUAAUUGAAUUCUUAAACUCAUGUACCUUUCUGUAGCCUUUGCUUAUGAUCUUGUUUGUGCCCUGGGCACAGACAGUACACUGAAGGACUGGCCUUCAAACCAGCUUCUCCCAUUGCUUUUCUCAUGAUAAUAGUGAGUAACAUUUAUUACACAUUCGCUUUGCCUUCAUAUACUCUCUACAUCUACACUUCACAUGCAUGAUGUCAUUUAAUCUUCAGAAUCACCCUCUGAAUUUGGAACAAUUCUUAUCCCCACUUUAGGGAUAAGAAAAUUGAGACUUAGACAAGGAAUCUCAAUCCCAGAACUAGAUUUCUUUUUCUUCUUCUUCUUUCUUUUUUGAUACAGGGUCUCACUCUGUUGCCCAGGUUGGAGUGCAGUGGCACAAUCACAGCUCACUAUAGCUCAAGCAAUUCUCCUACCUCAGCCUCCCCAGGAGCUGGUACUACAGGCAUACACCACCACACCCAGCUAAUGUUUUUCUUGAUUUUUUUUGUAGACACUUGUUUUCACCAUGUUGCCCAGGCUGGUCUCCAACUCCUGGACUCAAGCAAUCCACCUGCCUCAGUCUCCUAAAGUGCUGGGAGAACUUUAUUUCUUAACUAUAUUUCUUAACUAUUCCCCCAUAUGAUUCCAUCAGGACCUGAGUGAGAGUGAGAUAAUUUUUCAGGUUCUAUUCUCUGUGAUGCAGCCUCUGGCCAUGUAUUUAUAGUUUCAAAUAGAAAGUGAGUUACUAUCAGCAGGCCAGAAGUAGAAGACUUUGGGAAAUUUCUUUUAUCCAUGGUAUUAGUUUACAAACUUUAGUCCCUGAUGUAAGUAGGCAUCAUACUCCCAAAUUUAGAUUGAUGAGACAAAUUAGAAUGAAUGUAUCUAUGAUUGCAGGAUCAGUCACAGGGUUUCCUUGAUAGAAUAAUUCGCUCCUAUCUUUUGAUAUUUCAGCUUGAUUAGGAAAAAUUCAUUGUAUACACAAAUUUUUAGGCACAUAUCUAAGGCAUAAGAUAAGACACAUGUGUGGAUCCACUGGUUAAAAUGUUAAAUGUGUGGCUUGUUUCAUCAUUAAAGUCCCUCUAGUAUGCAUUUAUUUGCUUCCCAGAAGAAUUUGAUCUGAUCGUUGUUCUGCUGACCGCACACACCUGAUGCUUCUCUGAUCUUAUCUGCUGCUACUCUCUGCCUUGCUUAUUCUCCCCUUACUGUUCACAGGGAAAAUGUACCAAGCACUGUGGGACCGAAGUUCUGUUCCUGCCCUCAGGGAACUUCCCAUUUUGUUGAGGUGACAAGAUUAUACACAUGGGAUUAUUUGACAGUUUGGAGCUACACAGUAGUGCUAUUGAGAAAUAGGGCAGGUCUUAAGAGGAGGAUUUAGCGUAGAUUUUUCAGAGAAGGUGAAGGACUUGAACUGGAGAUUGGAUUUUGUUGGUGGAGUAAAGAGAUGGGGUUACAAGUCUGGGAGGUGGAGUGGGCAUUGGAAGACCAAAGACAGCAUAAAGGAAGAACUUUUUAAAGUUACGCAAUUAUAUCAUUACCAUGUUUCAAACCAUCUUGAAGGCAUGAUGCUGGAAGGAACCUAGCAUGUGGGUGGACUGGUCUGAUACACUUAACCAUUUUUCCUUGGUGUGUAUUAUAUGAGUUUCAAACAGUAGUUUAAUGUGGUGCCUCAGGAUUGACACAGGUGAUUUCUAUGCCCAAACUGCCUGUGAUGGCCCAACUGUGAUGUUCCUCCAGGGCCUCUGAAACACCCUGUGCCAUCAGGCUUAGCAACCCCAAGGAAAAUCUUGGAAAGGAGCACAUAUUGCUUCUUUUCCAGUAAAAACAAGUCUUUUUUUUUUUUUUUUUUUUUCUUCCAGCUUUUGUUUUAGGCUCAGGGAGUGCAUAUCCAGGUUUGUUACAUGGGUAAAUUGCAUGUUGCUGGGGUUUGGUGUACAAAUUAUUUCAUUACCCAGGUAGCGAGUAUAGUACCCAAUAGGUAGUUUACCAAUCCUCACCCUCCUCCCACCCUCCAUCCUCAAGUAGGCCCCUGUGCCUAUUGUUCCUUUACUUAUGUCCAUGUGUGCUCAGUGUUUAGCUCCCUCUUAUAAGUGAGAACUUGUGGUAUUUGGUUUUCUGUUCCUGCAUUAAUUAACUUAGGAUAUCCUAAUUAACUUAGGAUAAUGGCCUCCAGCUGCAUCCAUGUUGCUACAAAGAACAUGAUUUCAUUCUUUUUUAUGGCUGUGUAGUAUUCUGUAGUGUGUAUGGAAUAACAUUGUAUCACAGUUUUCUUGUCCAGUUUUCCAUUGAUGAGUUUCUAGGUUGAUUUCAUUUCUUUGUUACUGUGAAUGGUGCUACAAUGAACAUAGUUGUGAGUGUGUCUUUUUCCUAGAAUGAUUGAUUUUCCUUUAGAUAUAUACUCAAUAAUGAGAUUGAUGGAUCAAAUUCUUAUGAGGGUGGUCAGGGAAGUUAUUCUCACUUUACUGAAGAGGAAAUUGAUGUUCAUGUGCUAAGACACAAAAAUGUGAUUUUUUAAAUAUUACAUAUAUAAUAGGUAUGAAACAAUAUAUAUGAUAUAUGCAUAUAUACAUAUACACAGAUAUAUUAUAAUGUGCUAACUUCAGCAUUUCUGUGAGCUUUAACUUAGCCAAGGUGCCUGAUCUGAGAUCCAAUUGGAUUUUCAUUCCCUUUUGGCCUAAUGAACCACAUACACCUGCCCUUCUCUUAGGCUUGGCUCUUGCUAAUUAUCUCUCUCAAUUUGAUGUUCUUCUCUUCUCACUGUGUAUGUCAUUUUUAAUGAGACAAACCAGUGUUUGGGAGAGGUUUAUGGGCAAGAAGAAAAAUAAGACGAUCACUAACAACUGGCAGCAGGUUAUAAUGCCAAGAUCGUCUACAACAUUUUAAAUGACAUGCUGAGCUGUGUGCUGAGUUGCACCAUUUUCCAUUAACUGCUUUCAGCCAGAACAAGAUGAACAAGUGAGAAUGGGUUGAAAAAGCGACCUGAUCAUAAUGACUGCUAUUUAUUGGGCACCCAUUGUGUGCAGACACUGUACUCAGUCCUUGCAUAUUUUUUUUCAUUUAAACCUCAUACUAUUGUUAUCACCAUUUUGCAGAGAAAUAAAUGGAAGCCUAUAGAGGUUAAGUAGGUGACUCGAGAAGAUAUAACUAGUAAGUGAUGGAGCUGGUGGUCAGGAAUUUCUAUAUAUAAAUGUAUAUAUAAUAGUUCAUUAGAAGGAAGCUUUCAACAUAAGUCAAAUGCUUAUGGGUAAAGAAAAAUUGGGGGCCAGUUGUAAGACCAGACAUUUACUUCCAGUGCCAAUAACAAUAUUGUCACCAUAGCAGGUGCAGAAAUGAUCAUGGGGACAGAUUUCUUGCACAAAAAAAAAGUAUCCUUUAAGAUUUAAUUCGUAUGGCUAUUUGAAUGUGCAGUAAUAAAAAGAAGUAGGAAUAGACACAUAGAAUAAGUAACUUCAGAGCCUUCACAAAACCCUCCUGUCUGAAAGGAUAUCCUCUACCCAGUUGUCGUGUCAGAAAUUCCUUCCUUAGUAAUUAAUAUCCUUGCAUAGUUUUUUUAGGUGUCAUCUUAAUGUGGACAACAUCCAUCACAUAUCAGAUUUCCAUCAAAAUUCAGUUUGUCUUUUCACAUUUACUCCCCCUUCUUCCCUCUCCUGAGAUAACUUAGCGUCCUCACUCCACUUUUUACUUAAGCACUGAAUCUCACUUCAUCAUCUCUCCUCCAUCAGAACUUCUCCAUUCUGUGACUCUCUGUUCCUUGAUACCUUGUUCUCUAAAGCUGACAGUGGGUGAUCAUAGGUCAGUUAUUAGAUGGAAUCCUUUAGCCAUAGAUAAUAGGAUUUUUCUGCUUCUUAGAAGACAACGUCAUAAUAGUUAAGUAGCAGGCUGAUUGUAUGUGUUUUCAACAUCUGAAUUGUAAUAUAUCCAGAUGGGGGGUAGCUUGGGGAAGGGGGAUUCUUUUAGAUUCUGCAGGAGCUUUUCCCCAUACUUAAAUUCCUUCCUAAUGCAUAAAGCUGAUUCUGCUUGGAAGAGGGAAGCCAGCCUUUCAUUUUCCACCUGACACCUCAUGAUAGAUGGAAAUGUCCCUUCCUCUUCUCUUUCUUAUCUCUCAGCAUCCUUCUUCUCUGAACAAAUGAGCAUUCAUGACCCUUGGUGAGUCAAUUUCAUUUAAACAGAAGGCCAGAUACACCCCAGUGUAUUCAAUUAUUUUAUAAUCAAUUCCCUUUUCGGCAGCAUCUUUCUCCCAAGAGUCAGAGGUCCCUUUACAAACUGUAUUGGCAACAUUAUUACAAGUCAGAGCACAGUGACCUGCAUCUGAGGACAGCGAUUUAAGAGACAGUGAAUAUGAAAAGACAAAUUUGAUUUUGAUGAAUGAUAAGAAUUUUGUGUGUUAUCAACAUAAGGUGAAACCUAGAGAAACCAGUUCAACAAAUAAAUCACCAAUGAAGGAAUUUCAGGCAAAUCAAUCGGUGUUGGGGCAGUUAGGAGCUCAGCAAUUCAUUUCACAUUGUAGACACUCUCCAUAAAAUGAUUAAUUGUAUAAAUACACUAAUUCAAGAUACUUGUUGAGCUUUUGCUAUCACCAGACCCUGGGCACAGGGUGCUGGAGAUACAAAGGUUUAAGGGAAUAAGUAAAGGAAGCGGGCAAUGGUGAAAAGGAAGGAAUGAAUGAAGGAAGGAAGGGAGGGAGGGAAGGAGGGACGUAGGGAAGGAGGGAGGGAGGGAGGGAUUAUUCACUUUAGUAAUUGAAUAAUUUGUCUCUGACAGGAAGGGCUGGCCUUGCAAGCUCAACCAAGCUUUCUUAGUACUUCUUAAUAAUUAAAAUAAUUGGGCUAUAUGACUAAAAAUUUGCAGGUGGAAAUUUCUGUUCAUGUUCUGUGAUUGCUAGAGGUUUAUAAAGCAAAAACUUUAAAACUUAGAAAGAACCAUGUUAUGGCUUUGAGUCAAAGACUUGGACAGUUUUUGCACCUGAAAAAGAAACAGAAUCUAGACUCAUGAGGAGUUAGGUAAGUUCACAGGAAUUAGCAGACAGGAAUUCCAAGAGCAGCACAGACCUUUCCGUACUAAUGUUUCAAGCCAACCCACAUAUUGCAGUUGCUGAGCCACACCUAGACUUGCAGCGGAAAUGUAAAGACAAGAAAGAUAUUUGGCUUCUAACUUCCCCUGAGUCUGUUUCAGUUUCCUUUUUUGCAAACCUUUAUCAACAGUUGUUCAUAAGACUUUCUCAAUAACCAAAAAACUCAACAGGCAACCACAAGAGAGGGCCUCUUCACAGCAUACAGACAGCCACAAGAUACUACCAGAAAAAAAUAGAAUAAGAUACAUCACGUAGAUACAUAGAGAGGCUGUAGUGGUUUAUGCAGAGUAUAUUGAUCCAACUUCUAGACAUGGAAAAAUCAAUAUAUUUAAGUAGCCUCCUUAAAAUAAGUUGACUUUUCAGUAAGCAGUUUGGCCAACUGCUAGUGUACAGUGAAAGGAAUAAUUUAAGAUUUAGCCUUGGCCACAACUAGAUUCUGCAAACAUGUACAGAAGAAAGAGAAUGCUUUCCCUUUCCUUUUUACUACCUCCUGCAAUCAGUGGUUUGCCCAAGCAAAUUUUAAAAAUUGGAGAAAACGGGUCUUUGGAAGAACUAGCUAGAAAUAGGCUACAGCCGAGACCUCCUAACUAAUCUGUUGAAGGACGUCUUCUCGUUCUUUUCCAGGCUUUCCUUUGAUUCAAUUUUGAAAAAUCAGGCAAACUAGAAGAUUAUUAUUAUAACCACUGUUAUAAGUCAUUAUAAUUUUUUAUAAUUUAGAUUUAUAUGAUUACUGAUUCACUUGUAUUAUGUUCUUAUUGGGUGCCAGGUGUCAUACUACCCGUUGCCUGUAUAAUCAGUAACAAUAACAAAAAUCACUACAAGGUUGGUAGUAUUCUUCCUAUAAUUUGUAGAAGAGAAAAAUUUAGACUCAGACAAGUGCAAAUGACUUACUGGAAGUCCCACAGCUGUGAAGUUGCAUGGCCAGGGACUUAAAUGCUUGAGUCUGCCUGGCUGCAAUGCCUGGGCUAUUUCUUACUAUGCCAUGUUUAAUGAAACUAGAAUGCUGCCCUACACAAUAAAACAAGGAUAUGUCUUUAGUGCCAUUCUAGUCUUUUGCUGGGUAAUGAAGCAUUAACAGCAUAACCCCUAGAAGAAAUUUCCAUUUUUUAUUUUCCUUUGGAAUUAUCUGCCUUGAAGGUUCAUAGUAAAUUGAAGGGCUUACACAUUUCUUCUUCUAUGGGCAGCUUUAUAACAUACAUAUUUUGUAUGUUAUGUACUGUAUUAUGGGUCCUGUGAAGUCAAAGUCCCCCUGAUCCAUGAAUCUGACUUUUCCAGACAGCAAAUCACUUCACCAUCCCUUUCCCUCUAGUCUUUACAAUUCCUGCGUGAGCCAGAUGCUUCAGAAAACAGAUCCUUUGUAUUGAAUUUCCACACUGCAGUUCCCAGACUACGGAAGGAUGACGACCAAAUUUUUUAUAUUUUGUCAUCUCUAUUUAUGUGGAUAGAUAUAUAUUUAGAACAAGUUAAAAAGGAGGGAGGAAAAAAAACCCACUCCAAAACAAACAACUUCCUGAUCUAAUACAGAGGAUACAGGAGACUUUACCAUGAGUAGAAUGGACAGGAUGUCCACUGUUGCCACAACAGAGCUUAUUUGAGUAGAGUCAAACUAAUUUAUCUGAGAGGAUGCCUGGUUGCACAAGAGAAAGGGAAGUGAAAAGUUUGAGUUAUUUAGAAAAGCAAACAGUUAUUCUUUAGCAGGCAUCAAACACUUAAACUCUGGCAAACAAGUCCAUUCAAGAGCUCAUCACACAGAAAAUAACUAGCAAUGCAUAAUAUAUCUUUUCUAUGGCGAAAGAGUAAAGAAAGAAAGAAGAAAAAUAAUAAUUUUAUAUCUACCCAGAGACAACCAUGUUUAAAAAUUAGUACAUUGUUCUAGACUAUUUUGUGUGUAUAUACAUAUGUGUGUAUGGGUUUGCCUAUUUUUUUAUAUUUUAAUUUGAAAUUUAUGUUAAGUUCAUGAGUGCAUGUGCAGGUUUGUUAUAUAGGUAAACUUGUGUCAUGGUGAUUUGUUGUACAGAUUUCUUCACCCAGGUAUUAAGCCUAGUAACCAUUAGUUAUUUUUUCUGAUCCUCUCCUUCCUCCCACUCUCCACCCUCUGAAAGGCCCCAGUAUGUGCUGUUCUCCUCUAUGUGUCCAUGUGUUCUCAUCAUUUAGUUCCCAUUUAUAAGUGAGAACAUGGACCUGGUGUGAUGGCUCAUGCCUGUAAUCCUCGCACUUUCGGAGGCUGAGGCAGGCGGAUCAAUAGAGGUCAGGAGUUUGAGACCACCUUGGCCAACAUGGCAAAACCCCAUCUCUACUAAAAAUACAAAAAUGAGCCGGGCAUGGUGGUGCACGCCUGUAGUCCUAGCUACUCAGGAGGCUGAGGUAUGAGAGUCGCUUGAACCCUGGAGAUGGUGGUUACAACUAGCCAAGAUUGUGCCACUGCACUCCAGCCUGGGCGACAGACCAAGACCCUGUCUUAAAAAUAAAUCAAUAAAUAAGUGAGAACAUGUGGUAUUUGGUUUUCUGUUCCUGCAUUAAUUUGCUAAGGAUAAUGGCCUUCAACUCCAUCCAUGUCCCUGCAAGGGACAUGAUCUCAUUCUUUUUUAUGGCUGCAUAGUAUUCCAUGGUGUAUAUGGGGUAUGCCUAUUUAAACAAAAAUAAUAAAUAAGACCAUGUGAUAUAUUCUGUAUUUUAACCUGCCUUUUUUUUUCUUUUUUACUUAAAAAUACACCAUGGACAUUUUUCUCUGAAAAAACAAUUCAUUGCUUCCGAGUAUUCCGUGCCUAGAUCUACAACAGUUGUUGCUGUGCAUGUUGCUCCCUAUUACAAACUAUUCAUGAUGACAUCCUUGUGACUGACUGAAUCCUUGUUCAAUACUUACUGAUUUCCUUAGGAUAAAUUAAUUAAAGUUGCAUGAAUGGACUAAACACCAUGCACAUUUUCAAGAUGAUUAAACUGUCCCUGGAAACAUGGUUUCAGUCUAUAGCCUGAAUAUAGGAAAUGCCAUUUCUCCCAUGUCCAGUAAUACUGAAUGUUUAUUAUACUGAAUAACGGAAAGAAAUCAUUAUUUUGAAAGCUGCCUGUCUAUUCAUCUUGAUAUCAUAGUAAACGGCACAGUUAAUCUUAAGGAAAGACUGUAACUUUUAUUUAGAAAAAUGACCACUUGGUUUAUUUAGAUGUGAAAAGCUAAAGCUGGGGUAGGUAAAUUUUUUCUGUAAAGAGCCAAAGAGUAAAUAUUUUAGGCUUUGUGGGUUAUAAGAUCUCUGUUGCAACCACAGUUGACCCUUGAACAACACGGGGCUUGGGGCAGCAAUCUCUGCGCUAUUGAAAAUUCACAUAUAACUUUUGACUCUGUACUCACUUAACCACUAAUACCCUACUGUUGACCAAAGUCUUACCAAUAGCAUAAUCAAUUAACAUAUAUUAUGUAUGUUAUAUAUAUAUUAUGUACUGUAUUUUUACAAUGAAGUAAGCUAGAGAAAAAAAUGUUAUUAAGAAAAUCAUACGGAAGAGAAAAUAUAUUUACUAUCAUUAAAUGAAAGUAGAUCAUCAUACAGGUCUUCAUCCUCAUCAUCUUCAUGUUGAGUAGGCUGAGGAGGAGGAGGAAGAAGAGGGGUUGGUGUUGCUGCAUUGGGGUGGCAGAGAUGAAAGAAAGUCCAAGUAUAAGUGAACCUAUGCAGUUCAAACCUAUGUUGUUCAAGGCUCAACUCUGCUCAACUCUGCAGUGGCACCAAACUGUCGUGGAUAAUGAGUGUGACUGUGUUCCAAUAAAACUUUAUUUACAAACACAGGUGGAUUGGACCCACAGAGCUGGGGUGAACCAACCCCUGGGAUAGACCCUUGGGCAUGGUCUGUAAGGAUUAGAUUCAGACCAAAACAGAGCAAUAAUAGGGUGCAUGACGGAGUAACUCUUGGGAGGAGAGGCAGCAGUUAGAGGCAGUAAAGAUACGGGGGCAGUGGGACAAGACUUUGGGGUGAGAGAGAGUGUCCAGCGUCAUGGCAGCUGUUAAGGAUUACAGAGAAAGCCUUCCAGAGAGAAAUUCACUAUGGUUUGGGUGGGUGGCUGAAGAAAUUCAGCUGAGGAAUUGCAUCAUGUCUAAAAUUAAUUUUAAGAUAUUUCCUGUUUUGCUCCAAAUAAGAGUUCUCCUCCAUGUUUCUAAAGCCUUCAGUAAAAUGUUACUGACAAAUGAGGGAGCUAGGAAGGGCUCCUCCCAAGGAGUAGGUGGAAAAAGAAACAUCCCCAGGAGGUGUCAUGGUGAAUGGAGUGUCUGAGAAUUAAUCUAGGUGAGGGAAUCCAGACAAACUGUGACAGCAGAAUGUAAUUCUGCUUCUCUUCUGGAAUUUUCAGAAGUCCCCUGGGGAAUGCUGGCUUCUCUCCGUCUGUAGGAUGGGGCUAUAUCGGGCAAGGUCCUGGCAGGAAAUGGAUGGAAUGCUGGAGUAGAGGUGUGACCCAGGUUAUGUAACCAACCACGAUGGGGAUGAUGUCAGGGACUAGUGACAGUGGGGAGCCAUCAGCACCCCAAGCAUGGGAGGCUGGAGAGGGAGAUGCAUCAACAGGGGCUGAUGAAAGCUGCAGUCAGGGAAGACUCUCCACUCUGCCCCACUGCUAACACUUGUGGCUCUGUGCAGCCAAGAGCAGAGAGGAACCUAGUUGGGCAGGACAGUUAAAAUAACCACCGAGACCUCUUUUUUUCCACAUUUGUUCUUCUGCCUAUGGUCCUAAUGUCUGCACCAAAUAGAAGUCAGAGGACAAGCAAGACUGGUUAAUGAAGCCCACAGAGGUCAGUCUCUCAGGACAUCAAGAAAGACGAUGGAUUUGGGGGCAAGAAGUUGUCAUGGAGAGUAACCAGCCAUUUUAUUUGGAUAAUAAAAGAAAGCUGUGGAACUUGGGAUAUCUAUAUUUUUAAAAUCUACCAAAUUAUGGUAUUAUAUUAUUUCAUGUAAUAUAUGAUUGUAUUAUUAUUUUUAAUGUGACAACAAUAUUAGGUGCUUUGGACAUAGAAGAAGAGACAGCAAUACAAAUACAAAUCAUACAAAUGUGAUUUGCAGUUGCUGCUUGUUUUGGUUUUAGGAGUCUGAAAUAUUUUCCAACUUAAUCCAUGUUUAGUAUCUAUUCAAAGUUUCCUUUGUCCAGAAAAAACCUACCAACACUAAAAAAUAAUAAAAUAUUAAAAUAGAAGGAAAAAUUAUUCCCACUGAGUUCCCCUGCAAUGAUAGCAAUAUAUUAUAUUUACUGGUAAAAAUGAAGUUGAAUUUAUGCCACUUCAAACAUACUAAGAGUAACUGAAAGGUUUGCAUUUGUAUUCUGAGGGGGUGAGAAUGAUCCAUCUUCUGCAGAUGAGUCAGCUUCCAGGGUUGGUAGAGGGGCUAAGACAAAUGAUUGUUUUCUUGUGUAGCUCAAGGAAUCUUUGUACGUUUUUCUGUUGCAGCAAAUUGCAUUGCUAACAUUGAUCUUCAUUUGCUUAAAUGGAUGCAUUAGUUCUUAGAAGGAAAGGAGAGGUGCUAGUUAAUUUUUAGAGUAAGAGAUGUAGAUGUACUCUUCCAAGCAUUGAUUUAAUCAGCUUCUCUUCCCAAUGGAACUGGAAAUAAAUCGAAGUGAAGACCUGAAUUUCCCCAUCCCAUUACCUUCUUGUAUGAGGGAUUCCCUUGCAAAAAAAAAAAAAAAUUGAGACAGGGUCACCCAGGCUUGAGUGCAGUGGCACGAUCUUAGCUCACUGCAGCCUCAAACUCCUAGGCUCAAGCGAUCCUCCUGCCUCAGCCUCCCAAGUAACUGGGACCACAGGCAUAUGCCACCAUGGCCGGCUAACUAAUUUUUAUUUUGUGUAGAGACAAAGUAUACUAUGUCACCCAGGCUGGUCUUGAACUCCUGGCUUCAAGCGAUCCUCCUGCCUUGUCUUCCCAAACUGUUAGGAUUACAGGCAUGGGCCACUGCACCCAGACCCAAAUUAAAUUUUUAUAAAGAAAUGACAUUUUAUUGUAUUGGACCCUGUGAUAUAAUAGUAGUGGGCUCCGUACUUUAGUGUGAGAUACACAAGUUUAGGAACAGAUUUUGGCUAUUUCAUUGCCACCUGCCAACGUUGUAAUGAUGACACCCAGAAAAACCCCACACCUCUAAAAGUGCCUCUGUCAUUAGACCACCUGCUUUUUAUUGAAUGUUUCAUUCAUAGAUUGAAAGGGGGUUUUACUUUAUCAGGAAACAGGGAAUUACUACUUCUACCUUUGCUGCAAAUCAAACUCCAUUAGAAUUUCAUCUUCCUUCACUGAGGCACAACCCUUUAAACACAGGUCUUUGCAUGACCCCUUAUGCAACUUUCCAUUAAUACAGUCCGAUCACUCCUGCCUGCAUUGCGGAUAUCAGUUAACAUGAGUAAUGCUGGCCAGAUAUCAAGAAUGUCAAUCAAGAAACAAAGGAAAGGGUGUUUUAUAAUUACAAAACCGUGUUUUAUAAUUACCUCUGUGCUACGUGCAAUUUCCUGACCCCAAAUGAUAAUAAAACACAGUCAUCCAAUUACACAGUCAGCCAGUCUAUGAGAUCUGUGUCCUUUGAAGAUUAAACUUCACUAGGAUUGUCCUCACAUAUUUGGUCUCUACUAAUCAGAAGUUUCCUUGUGGAACAAUUGAGCAGAAAAACCCAUAAAGAAGAAUUUCUGUUCUAUAGUACAGUCACUGACUUGCUUUCAGAGAAAUGGUAGUCCCUGUGGUGACCUCUAAAGAUCCUCCAGAGAGCUCCCUGCAGUAGACUCCUACCUCACUUUACUUUUUUCUAAAUAUCUUACUUCUGCACACUUGAAAGUCUCUGUACCUCUCCUCUUCUCAUUUUCAAAAAUAUGAAUUUUUGAAAUUCGUAUCUGGCUUUAUGCUGGUCCCCAGAGAUCACUGUUGGUUUCACUUGUUCCUCACCAACACUCCCAAGGUGUGAGUUGAUCUGUCCUCCCCACUCUCUGCAAGACCCAGAAGAGAGCCCUAGUUUAGUGUUUAGAGAUGCAUGCAGUGUUUAGCACCUUCUUUGUGUAAAGUUCCCUAUCUAAAAGAUACCUAUCAGUCUGUUAAUUUCUGGAAAAAGGAAGGAAAUGUCUUACUGUAAGAGGCAAAUUCAUUACUCCAGUCUGUAAAGGCACCAUUUAAAUAAAGCUCCUGAAAAGAACAGCUGAAUGAAACACUGCCCAUAUGACUUAGAAGAGUUCACCAAUGUGAGAAAGGUGGAGAACUUAUGCUGUACCUUCAGCUGUAGGAGGAAGCUCAGCAAGGAGUCCUGAGCUGAGACAGGGAUGCUCAGGUGCCAUCCUGUGACUCGAUCCCUUUGCUUCCUGUAAGAAAUAAAUCAGAAAUAAAUCACCUCAGACAAAUGUGAUGCUUUCAGUUGCUUACAUCCUCCAGAACAGGCGAGCCAGUCACCUGCCUCAGUAACUUAUCCCUUAGUCAUUCUGGGUUGGUACACUUUUACUGAUAUCUCAUGAAAAUUCUUUUUAUUGCUUUUAGAAUCAAUGGAACACAACAUCCAAGAGAAUCAAGAAAAUCUUUUUUAAAGGCACAGCUUUCUAACUCAAAAUGGUUUUACUUAAGCCAGGGGCCAUAAGAUGGCAGGCAGUGCUUUGCUUGGCUGUCAGAGGAAUUGAUUUUUCUUUUUAAGUUGAAUGUCUUUGCUUCUGUUCUCCUGUUUUCAGAGGCCCUAUUAUUUCCUACAGUUGUUCAUCCAGCCCAUUCACCUGUGUAUUCUACCUGCCCAUCCCCUAUGGAUUAAACUUUUACUUCCUCAACUUUGUUUAUAAAACACAAUAUUUAUAUGGCUACUUCUGUAUCUCUUACACAUACCCUAACUCAAUACUGACCCUGGAAUACUUUGGAGAAUAGAGUUGAAGGCUUUGCAUGUCACAUACAGUCUUUAUGGCAUACUCCACCUCCUCCUUCUCCCCACUUUCUCCUCUUCCUUCUCUAUUUCUCCUUCUUCUCCUUCUUUUUCUUUUUUACAACCUUUAAAAAUGUAAAAACUAUUCUUAGCAUGUAGGUCCUACAAAAAUAGACCAAGAGCCAGAUUGGCUAUAGUUUGCUGACCACUGAUAUAGAAAAAUGAAAGUGGAGAAGACACUUAGAUUCAUGUUUUUAAAAAUUAGGAGGGGGUAAAAUACCAUACUUCUUGGGUGUUUGUUUCUUUGUUUGUGUGUUUGUUUGUUUGGAGAGGGACUCUGGCUCUGUCACAUCACCCAGGUGGGAGUGCAGUGGCGUGACCUCGGCUCACUGCAACCUCCGCCUCCCAAGUUCAAGCAAUCCUCCCACUUCAACCACCCGAGUAGCUGGGACUACAGGGGCUCACCACCAGACCCAGCUAAUUUUUGUAUUUUUAGUAGAGACAGCAUUUUGCCAUGUUGGCCAGGCUGGUCUCAAACUCCCAACCCCAGGUGAUCUGCCCACCUCGGCCUCCCAAAGUGUUGGGAUUACAGGUGUGAGCCACCGUGCCUGGCCGUAAAACACUAUACUUCUAACCACAUGUAUCUGAGUCUGAAUUCGUAGAACAUGAAUCAAAAUUGCCUAGAAAUGCUUAAAACAAAGAAAGAAAAUCAAUGACUCGUUGCCAUGAAGACUUAGUAAAUUUGGACAUGAAUCUCUAAUAUGAUCAUGUGAGGUUAAUGUCUCAUCCAAAAGGAAGAGAGCUGUAUAAAGUAGAAGUGGAUACACUGGACACCAAGAAGAUGCAUCCUUCUGUGCAAACGCACUGCCUGACAUUAGCGUGUGGACAGGACUGAUGUGAUGUUAUUGUGCUAGUGAUUAAAGUCACAGGCUGUGGGAUCAAAUCCUUGCUCAACCACUGACUAGCUGGGAGGUAACCAGUCUUAAGCUCUCUGGGCUUCAGUUUCCACAUCUGUGAAAUGGCUGUCAUCAUUGUAACCACUUCCUAGUGGUUGUGUGCUGUUGAGAAGAUUAAAAAUGCUUGAUACAUUUGGGUAAUAGAAUGUGUUAAAGUUUUUUCUUUUUCUUUUUCAAUUUUAUGUGCUGCAAAAAAUAAUAACAAAAAGUGAUUAAAAAAAAAAGAAGAAGAAAAGAAAAUAACUGUGUUUGGAUGUGCCUACAGGCCGCCCAUCAUUCUCUCUUCCGGACAAAGUCUAAAUCAGUUUUUCCAUUUGGGCCAGAGCUUCCUAUUUGCUGCUAUGGAGACUGUUGUGGAAUGCCUGGAGCUGCUUAACAUAAGGCUUAAUUACCCAUGGCCUGUAAGCCAGUUCCAGUUCCCCACCUCUUUUUUCUUUAUUUGCCUAGGAGUUAGGUUGUGUUGAUUGUUUGCUGUAACUGUAGAUGUCAGAGCUAAAAUUUCUUCUGGCAUCCUCUUUCCUUCUACCUCAAGUCCUUAAAAUAUGUCUGACACAUGGAAAUGCUCCGUAAAUAUUAGUUAUUAUUAUUGUGAUUACUCUUUUUGUUUUACUGCAAAAUCAAUGAAAGGAAAUGGAUAAUUUUCUUCUGAGAGAUCAUACUCUAGACGAAAGAUGCCAAGGUGAUGGAGGAUCUGAACCUGGAUGCUUCAUUCUAUAUAAAAUAUAACAUGUGCCAAGUUCUUGACUGUGACAGCUUCAUGGCUCAGAAGGUGGAGGAAGUGAUGAGGGCAGCAGCUGCUAUGGACCAUCUUGUCUUCAGCCAAAUAUAUAAGAGGUGCAUCACUUUUCUUCCAGCUCUCCUCCUGUCACUAAAUUUAAAGAAUCUAAGUAUCCACCCUCUGGCAAAAACAGAUCAUGGAAAAGAAGCAAGUAACUGCUUUCCUGCUGAAUUUCUCUUAGGGCCAUUGACUGAUUUCCCCUGGGUAUAGACAGGUUACUCUAGGAACAUGGGGUCAUGUAUGGCUGUGCCAUUUUUAAUCAUGCCAGCUCUGACUCUUCCAUUAACUUUGUAAUUUGAAUAUGUCACAUGGUAGUUAUGAUCCUCCACUUCCUCACCAAUAAAAUGGGAGUAAUAGCGACACUUCCCCACCUGUGCAGAAGGCAAAAAUGUAAAGAAGAGUUAAAAAGCACUCGACAAGCCCAAGUGCUUUGUAAAUAUUUAAUACUUAGUAGUUGAGGUAAAUGUCAGGAGAAUGUGGAGCCCAACAUGAAUCUUUUUGUUAUGACAGCUCUUUAGAUGUGUUUAAUUCCCCAGUCCAAACACAGAGAACCCUGAACUUUUCUGACCCUUUCUCCUUGUCUUAUUUUUCUUCUUCUACUAUGCCCAAAUAUUUCCCAUCUACCAUUAAAUGACAGUUCAUUCGAAUUCCUCUACAAAAGAUAAUUUUAGUUUAUUAGGAUCCUGCAUGGGCUGCUCUCCACUUUGAGUUCCUAAAUGCUUGUACAGAAAAACUUAGGUUUCUUGGGAAAUUCCCUUUUUUGACAAAAACACCUCUUUGUGUUUGAAAAGGACUGAAUGCCAUUGUCUGAGAACAACCCCCAUUGUUGGAAGUCCUCACUUCUCAUUAGGCUAGCUCGUUUCCACAGAAAGGCUCAAAUAAUUUUCUUUCAACUUCACAACCCUACUGGGCCCUUGAAACUAAGCAGAUUUUGCACCUGUUCCCCUGAGGAAGGUUUGCUGAUUGAUAGGAGGGGUCUAGGUAAAUUGAGUAUAAAUAAACAGGUAAAAAAGAGAAGGCUUUUAAAUAAUGCAUUGGGGUUUUUCCAGAGCAACUCUGUUUUCUCUUGAAAUUACUAGAGAUUUUCAGUAAACAUUUGCCUGGAUACAUUUUCACAGAGGAGUUUGCCGCAUUCUGAGGACCUCAUUGGCUCCCACUGUUCAUUGCUAUGCCCAUCUCACACCCACUUCAACUGUCAAACAGAAGAACAAUUCUUAUUAACAGUGAUUUGCUUUGCAGUUUUAGUUUAUUUCUAAAUUGCAGACAUGGUUGAUGAGUGAAGUUGUUUUAGUGACUGUUUAUUGGAACAGAGCAGAGAAUAGAGUCAGGAAUUCUUGAGGCUGCCAUGUGUAUGGUGAAAAAUAGAAAUAAAAACCAUGCCAUUUUGCUUAAAAAGAAAAAUCCCCAGAAACCUUAAUGGUGAUACAUGCAAUCUGAGGCUAGAUAGCUUGUAUUUGUAGUGUGCUUUGCAAUUUUCAUAGGACUUUUAUGUGCAUUUUCUUCUCAGCUUUAAAGUACUUGUUUUGAGGUUUUUGGUUGAUAACCUCCAGUAACAGCUGUAGAAGAUAGUGCUAGGAUGGAUGAUUGUGAGUUAUAGGGAGGAACAUUGUUACACUAAGAAGGAAGGAAGGAAGGAAGGAAGGAAGGAAGGAAGGAAGGAAAGAAGGAAGGAAGGGAGGUAGGUAGGUAGAAAAGGUCAAUGAGCCUCUCUAAGACUUGCUUUCCUUUUCUAAAACAUGAAGAUAAUAAUAACUCUUACCCUAUCUGUCCCGUAAGGUCUUCGAUCACCUGCAGUAGACUGACUCUACAUUAAAGUAUUGCUUCAUCCAAAGAGUACUUUAGAAGCUUUAGUGGGUGUUAUUGGUUACAUUAUUAUGACUUAGGAAAAGUUGAUGUCUUCAUCUGUUCAGGCUGCCCUAACAAAAUAUCAUAAACUGUGUAGCUUAUAUACAACAAAAAUUUGUUUCUCAUGAUUCUGGAGGCUGUGAAGUCCAAGGCAGAUUUGGUGUCUGGUGAGGGCCCACUUAUGGUUCAUAGAAGGUGUCUUCUUGCUGUGUCCUCAUAGUAGAAGGGGGAAGCACUCUCUCUCAGGCCUCUUUUACAAGAAUACUAAUCUCAUUCAUGAGGUCCUUAUGACCUAGUCAACCCUCCAAGGACCCCAUCUCCUACUGCUAUCACCCUGGGAGUUAGGAUUUCAAUAUGUGAAUUUGGGGAGGAUACAAACAUUCAGACCAUAGCAGUUGGUCCACCCAAAAUUGUUUCAUUCACUGGCCUACUGUGCUAUAAAGUUCUCACUUUGGGAAAAUAACACACUAACUCUAUAGCAUUUAUGGACAUAUCAACUGGAUUGGCUCAGCCACUUAUAUGUUGCCUUCUUAGGAGACCUAAGAAGAGUGAAAAAUGGGAUUAUACAUUAUGACAAUUGAAAGGGGUGGAUAAAAGCUCUGAAUUGGAGGAUAACAGAAAAGAAAUGAGGUUUGCAUUGCAAGGUAGGUGGAGAGCAUGCUGAAGCCAGACUUCACCAAGACAUACCUUGACAUGGCUGGCCCCAGGUUUGCCCUCAGCCAUACAAAUCAACAGCUGCUGUGUUCUCCUAAGUGACUCCUGAACUCUAAUCUCUGCAUAUUGCUUGUGAUUAGAUCUCUCUGAGCUUGUUUUGGUUUUCAUUUUCUUCUAUCAAAAAUUGCUAGUUCAUAAGAUAUGUCAGAGUUGGACACAAAUUACUUUUCUUCCUCUCUUAGAAAUGACAAAUGACUUUUCUUCCUCUCUUAGUAUGUUCCUUAGAAGUAACAUACACUAUACAGUCAUGAGAUUUCUUUGAACUGAGAACAAAUAUCUAGCUGUCUUUCAUUUCUUUGGUGCUUCAUAGUCGACAAAGUGUUUUUUCAUGCUGUAUAUAAUUUAUUUAGUGCAGUAACUCUAUGAAGUAGGUAACCCCAAUACUUUUAGGAAAAUUAAGGUAAUACAUACCUACCUUGCAAGGUUGAGAGGAUUAAAUGGGACAACAUUUGUAAAUAACUUUUCACAACCCCCUGGGCAUAGAGAAAAGUCUUAUUUUUAAUACCCAUAUUUUAUGGAUGAAGAAACAAUUUCAAAGGAUGUGUGAUAUGCUCAAGGUCACACAACAAGUUGAAGAUGGAUCUAUCACUUGGACUGCCGCUCCAUCAUGCUAAUAUAUCACGUUGAUGAACAGUCAAACCAUUUGAUAUUUAGGUUUAAAUUCCAUGUUACAAACUUUUGAGGAAGAAAGUGAGACACAGAAAGAAGGAAAGAGAGAGAGAUGGAGAGAGAGGAGUUUAAGAACACUGAUGGGCUAAGACACAGGUAAGACAUGUUGAAUACCUCCCCCAGGUGUGAUUAGGAUAUCACGUAAAAAUGAUGUGUGCCUGUGGCUCAGGUGUGGUUAUGUAAUCAAAACGGCUGUGGGAAUGAAAUGCAUUUAAUUUUCCUCCAGCUUCCUGUUUCUAAGGCUUCAGUGUUUGAGUUCUGCCACACCAGCCUUUGCAUAUUAAUAGACGGUUGGCAAUCCCUGGGGAGCCCAGGGUGAGGGAGAGGUCCUCUGCAAUAAAAUCCAAGCUGGUUCAGUUGAAGGUAUUUGUGAAGCCUUUUUAUAUCCACUUUGCUUCUUGACCUCCCAGCAUACAUCACGGAAAUGUUAUUUCCAGCACCUGAAGCUUUGGUCUCCAGCAAAACCAGCUCUUGAUAGAAUUCGGCAGUAAGCAGGUUCAUGGUCAUUGGCUCCUUGUUAUUCUUUUUGGCCUCCUUGCCAUACUUUUAGUUCUCUUCACUGAUACCUGCCUGUUGCAGAGUCUUACGUUUGUCUAAGGUCUCUUCAGAAUAUCAACUUUUGUCCUGGGCCUUAGCUAUUAUCUCUCCAAUUUUCCAUGAUUCACCAGUUGAGGGGUAAUAUGGGUAGGCUUUGUGUCCCCACCCAAAUCGCAUCUUGAAUGGUAAUCCCCAUAAUCCCCACGUGUCAAGGGAGAGGCAAGGUAGGGGUAAUUGAAUCAUGGGGACAGUUCUGUUCUCAUGAUAGUGAGUUCUCAUAAGAUCUGAUGGUUUUUAUAAGAGGUUCUUCCCACUGUCACUCGGCACUUCUCCUUCCUGCCGCCUUGUGAAGAAGGUGCCUUGCUUCCCCUUUGCCUUCCACCAUGAUUGAAAAUUUCCUGAGGCCUCUCCAGCCAUGCUGAACUGUGAGUCAAUUAAACCUCUUUCCUUUAGAAAUUACCCAGUCUCGGGGAAUUCUUUAUAGCAGUAUGAAAACAGACUAAUAGAAGGGGAUACUUUCAAAAGAACAGAGUUUACAAUAAAAAUACUUGGUGAACUAUUGUGAGCCACCCAUGGUGCUGCUUGAACCAACCUCUUCCUGCCUCCUGCCUGUUCUUCCUCCUUCCUAGGAGAAUCCAAAGAUGGCUCAUUUGUUCCCUGGUGUAUUAGUUUGCCAAGGCUACCAAAACAAAAUACCACAGUCUGUAUGGCUUGGCCAGCAGACAUUUAUUUUCUCAUGGUUCUGGAGGCUAGAAGUCCAAGGUCAAGAUUUGGUUUCUUCUGUGGCCUCUCUCCUUGGCUGCAGACGGCUGCCUUCUUCCUGGGUCUUCACAUGGCCUUUCUCUGUGUACAUAUAACCUUGGUGUUUCUUUUAUGUGUGUCCUAAUAACACUUUAUAAUAAGGACACCAACCACGCAGAUUAGAUUAGGGACCACCCUAAUGACCUCGUUUUAACUUAAUCACCUCUUUAAAGAGGCUGUCUAUCUCCAAAUACAGUACAGUUCUGUGGUCCUGGGGGGUUAGGGCUUCAACAUAUAAAUUGUGUAAGAGGUGGCACAACUCAGCCCACAACAUCUUGUCACCUUGCUCCCUUCAUGCCUUGCUGCCUCCCUUUUUGGUUUCUUUGGUGUCUUGUUUUCCAUUCAUCUGGUCUCACUUCAGGGCUCCAGGUCCCCUUAUGGAAGUCCCUUGUGUCAUCCUCCAAGCCACUCUCCUAUUCUCCUGCAAAAAUUUGCUGACAUUCAAGCUGCCUUUGGGGUUUGUGUAAACUUUGUGGCAUUGACCUCGGGUUGUCACAUGCCCAUAGCCUCAUCUGCUGACUUGUGCUACAGCCCUCUUGCACCAGAGCAAUGACACUUUUCAUAAGACACAAAAUGUACAGACUUGUAUUCUCUUUCUUAAGUGCCCCUAAGUAGUUUGACUGCUUUUCCUGACUCAUUCUUCCUAUUUUAUGUCCUCUCCUUCUUAGAACUUCACAAGUUCUUUUAUGGGCUGGUUUGAAAAACAGUUGAGAUGUGUUCACUUCCAAAGCUUUCUCAUCCACUUAUAGCCAGUCAUCCUUUAACCAUCUGGACCCUCUCAGAAAUCUCUAAGCCGGAGGGCUCUUUUUCCUCUCAAGACUUUGCAGACAGUUAAAAGGCAGCCAUCAUCCAGUUUAGUGCUGGCCACAUGACAUAGAUGCUGCAAUUUUGCUCUCUUUCUGGAGGAGGUUCCACCAAGCUGUGUUUCAGCAUGCAUCAUAGGGCUUCAUCCUUCUGGUUCUGGGGUAAACCCUAGAUUGAACCCUAGAAUUGCCAUCUAAUUGUUCGAUAACCCAGGAGCAUUAUUUCCAUCGGUCUUAUCCUCUUCAUCUAUAAAAUGGUGAUAAUGACACCUACUUCUUAGUCUUGCUGUCAGACAUGAAGUAAGGUGGCAUAAAGCCUGGCGCAUAGCAAGCAUUCAAUAAAUGUUAGCUUUCGUGACAAUUUUGCAAAUAAAGCUUUUUUUUUUUUUUUGAGACAGAAUCUCGCUCUGUCACACAGGCUGGAGUGCAAUGGUGCAAUCUUGGCUCACUGCAACCUCUGACUCCCGGGUUCAAGCAAUCCUCCUGCCUCAGCUUCCUGAGUAGCUGGGAUUACAGGUGCCUGCCACCAUGCCUGGCUAUAAUUUUUUGUAUUUUUAGUAGAGACAGAUUUUCACCAUAUUGGCCAGGCUGGUCUCCACCUCCUGACCUCAGGUGAUCUGCCCACCUCGGCCUCCCAAAGUGCUGGGAUUACAGGCAUGAACCAUCGCGCCUGGCCUGCAAAUAAAACUUUGUGACAGGCAGGAACUUCUUCGGUCAUAAGCUUUCCUUCUCCUGUUUGUGCUCCUCUAUAAUUUGCAUUAAACAAAAUAUUUAUUGAAUAUCUGUUAUCUUCUAAGCACUGCGUUAAGUUCUUUACAUUUGUUGAUCUUAUUUAAUUCCUCACCAUAAGCCUUAAGGCUGAUAUUAUUACUAACAAAACUUUACAAUCCUGAGAAUUUAGCCUUGAACAAGACAGAUAUUAUACACUCCUGUCAGAUCUUACAAUACCGUGAGAAAGUCUUAUGUUAAACUAAUAAUUAUAAUACAAUAAUUAUAGCAGCCUACUCUUCCUUGAGGCAGUACCUACUUUCCUAUAGUUAUUACUGGAUCUUGGAAUUUAAAUAGAGUUUCCUUACUAUUGCUAAGCACUACAUGUUGUGAAAUUAUAUAAUCAACUUUUGCAUUCCUUAAGAGUCUUAUCAAUGAAAACCCUGAAAUCUUAGAGAUGGAAACAAAUGGAAGGGAUAUGGUUGUUUGUUAUGUCAGAGCUAAUUAUUUGUAAUUACUUUGUAAGCAGGAGAUAAAUAUUCAUGCUUCAUUCCUUCUUUUAGAAGGGACCAAGUAGUUUGGAAAUCUCAGACAACAUCCUGAUAAAAGGCAGUUGAAGAAAGACAAAUAUUACUUGGUUGGCUUAAUUGGAGUUUGGAAAAGAUCUAUUGCUUGGAGCUCCAGAAUCAUUGAGCCUGGGCCCUGUAAUUCCACAGAGCAGUGUGCUGAACACAAAACCAAUGUUGUAUGGAGGAAAAUGACACAGACGCCUAUGCGUGGACCACCAAUUGCCAGCCAAGGAUACCUUUUGGUGCCCUCAAUUUAAAACCACAGCCAGAUUUUUAACAUGGAUAGACCUUCUCAUUCAUACAAAGUGAUACCUCAAGUGUGAUGACUCACUCUAGGAGGAGGAAAGAAACAGACUACUCAAUGCUUCUGAAAUAAAUUAUUGUAAUAUUUUACCAUUUCGUGUUUGUUAGAAAGGCUAUUUGUCUACCUCAUACUUGGCAUAUACACGAUUUGUACUCCCAGUCAGGGCCUGUUGAAUGAAAUUAGUUUCCUCUAUCAAUCAUCCCUGUGAUGUCUGUUACAUGGACUAGCAUUCUGGAUACUACCUAAUAGCAACAGUUCUAAUGAAAAUGGUCUAAUAAUAUUGCUCCUUGCAACAGAUGUGUUUUAUCCCAAAGUAUAAACUCCUUAAAGCAUAGACAGGCAGAGUUGGCUCAUGCCUGUUAUGUAAGCUAUCAUGUCCUUUCUUUCUUUUCUUUCUUUUUGUUUUUUAGAUGGUGUCUCAUUCUGUCACCCAGGCUGGGCUGGAGUGCACAGCGUGAUCUCAGCUCACUGCAACCUCCACCUCGUGGGUUCAAAUGAUUCUCCUGCCUCAGCUUCCCAAGUAGCUGGGAUUACAGGCAUGCGCCAACAUGCCCAGCUAAAUUUUUGUACGUUUAAUAGAGACGAGGUUUCCCCAUGUUGGCCAGGCUGGUCUUAAACUCCUGGUCUCAAGUGACUUGCCUACUUUGGCCUCCCAAAGUCUAUCAUGCCCUUUCUAUUGAGUGGCCGCCUGCAAGUGUCUCAAAGAAAUGUUUAUUACCUAUUUAUAGAAUAUUUCUUUGUUCAAAAUAGAAAUGAUUAACUCUUAACUGAAGUAAAUGAUAUAAUUACCUGAAGAACAGAAAGGAAACUUUUCAUGCUCAAGAAGGCAGAACCCACAUCCUCAGAGUGAGGUUUCUGCUUUUCUGGUUAAACAUGAGUAUUAACUGGAAAAGUCUACUUUAAAGCAUGAGCUCUGGUAGGCACAGCUAACAUUAUUUUGGACACCUUCACUUUAUUUUAAUCAUAAACUGUAAUGCUGGCUUCCUCUUGGUUGUUCAAUAUUGCAGAAAUGAGUCGAGUUAACCUACAAGUUGUAGGAAGCAUUUGAUGACAGAAAGAGACUUGAAAAAGUAGCCGAUUUACCCGCAAGUCAUAUCAGCACUUUGAAGAAACAAACACUGCCACAGUACCCUGUUAAAAGUGUCAGUCAUAAAGCUCUUUACAAAGGUAUUGUGCCUCCAACUUUUAAUUUUCAUACCCUCAUGGAGAGAUAAGCAUCCUCAAAAGAGCCCAAUUGCCUUAUAGGGCUUUCAAAGGAAGCUCCAGUUUUGAAACACUGCUCACUGCUUAUACACUACCCCCAUUCCCAUGAAAUAAAAUUGUCAUACUAGUCCCCUUUGCAGAAGUUAUAUAGCAUUCGGGAAUACUGAAUGUUUUCUGUUGAAGUUCAUCUUAGAGAGCUUAAAAAUUCAACAAGUCAUAAUCAUAACCCAGAAUUAAGCCCAUGGUAUACAGCAACAGCUGGGGUCUGGGUGAUAGAGAGGAACGAGUUCUGCCGUAGACAUCUGCAGGUUUGGCUACUGGUUCUGGGUCUGGUACUCACUUGCUAGGUGAUUCAGGGCCAGUCUUCUCUCAGUGAGCCCCAGUUUUCUGCCCCUGCCAUGUAAAAUGAGCCUGAUAUCUGCAUGAUCACCAAGAUGUUUUCCUGCACUGACUUCCUAUGACUCUGGGCAAGGCAGGGGAGCUAACCUUUUCUAAUGAAAUAUUAAGCAAUCAGGACUAGACGCCUUGGAAGUCAUCUCUUCAAGCCCAGUCCUUCCAGGCUUUCAUCAGCUGACCCAGAGAGGUGAUAUUGUUCCUAUUGAUCCUGUUUCUAAUGCUCCGCCAUUGACUAGCUUUCACAUCUUUCACUCUCUCUGAAAGUAAAGAGCUGCUGCCCCUUUUUACAGAACACGUGUGUUUCCUGUAUAUUGUGGUUGUAUACUUUCUUUGCUCUGACUUGUGAAAAGAAAGAAAAAACAAGAGAGCUAAGAAUUCUUUUUCUUUUCUUUCCUCUUGAGCAAGCUGAAAUGGGCAGGGUAUAAUUUAACUUGGAUUUAUAAAACGGCAGUUUAUUCAUUUAACUGAAAAUACUUGUACUUUUUCUUCUUAGCUAUUAUUUAUUAUUUGUUUAAUUUUUUAUUAUUAUACUUUUUUGAGACAAAGUCUCACUCUGUUGCCCAGGCUGGAGUGCAGUGGUGCUAUCUUGACUCAUGGCAACCUCCACCUUCUGAAUUCAAGCAAUUCUCCUGCCUCAGCCUCCCAAGUAGCUGGAAUUACAGGUGCUUGCCACCACACCCGGCUAAUUUUUGUAUUUUUAGUAGAGACCGGGGUUUCACCAUGUUGGCCACGGUAGUCUCAAACUCCUGACCUCAACUGAUCCACAUGUCUCGGCCUCCCAAAGUGCUGGGAUUAUAGGUGUGAGCCACUGCACCCGGCCACUAUUAUUUAUUAAGCAAACCCAUGGCAGGCACUGUGCUAAACUCUCUCCCUAAAGAUACACUAUUUAAAAGGUUCAAAUCACCAUGAAAAAUAGGUGUUAUUGUUCCCACUUUACAGAAGAUGAGAUUAAAGUUCAAAAAUAUUAAGUGACUUGCUUAGGGUUACUAAGCGAUGGACCUGAGAUUCCGAUUCAUCCCAAAGAUCCUAAUCACAAUAUGUUUAAAUCAUUUUGAAGAGACGUAAGAAGGUGUAAUGCUUUCAUUUGUAAAACAGUUUGUUGUAAAAUCAAACUCAUUUUGAGGUAUGUUUUAAGCUUACCACUUGAAUAUUUAAAUUUCAUUAGAACUGGGCCUGGCACAGUGGCUCAUACCUGUAAUCCCAGCACUUUGGGAGGCCGAGGAGGGUGGAUCACCUGAGGUCAGGAGUUUGAUACCAGCCUGGCCAACAUGGCGAAACCCUACUCUACUAAAAAUACAAAAUACUCUACAAAAAUACUAAAAAUGCAAAAAUUAGCCGGGCAUGGUGGCGUGCACCUGAAAUCCCAGCUACUCGGGAGGCUGAGACAGAAGAAUCACUUGAACCCAGGAGGCUGACGUUGCAGUGAGCUGAGAUUUGUGCCACUGCACUCCAGCCUAGGCGACAGAGCAAGACUCUGUCUCAAAAAAAUAAUCAUAAUAAAAAUAAAAAAUAAAUAAAAUUUCAUUAGAACUGUUCCUGGCAUAGGAUAGGUGGGUACUUAAUUUGGUUGAACAGAUACUUGGAUUUAUAAAAAUGAGAUUUAUGUGUGGGACAUCACUAACGGGUUGUUGGCAGAAUUAUCAGUGCACCUGUUGUAUGUUGAGUGAGACAACUGCUUUCGCAGGCUCUGUGUUUGCAGUUGACCUGAUGCCACAGUCAUGUGCAUGGUGGCUUUAGGAGCGGCAGUUCUGGUAAAGUCUUGGUACACUAACUCACACUCUGUCCUUAAAAAUAUGUUAGUGGAAAGACUGCAUCUAACAAACUGAGUGUCCCUUUUGGCAUGUUUUUCAGUGGCAUCACUAUCCUGUGAGGUCGAUGGUAAAUUAGGCAUAGUCCUUCUUCUGCUCUAUCAGCUGCUCUGAAAGCAACAGGACUCUCAUUUUCAGGCUCUUAGACAAACUUGGAUUCUUGUAGGCAGAGCAUAGAGCUAUUAAUCAAAAUGACAGCAAUUGUAAUUAUAGCUACAUAGGGAAAUAUUAUUUUUAAAGUUAAUUUUGAAUAAUCAAUGCAUGCAUGGAGUAGAGAAUUCAACAAGUACCAAAACUCUCACCCUCAGCCCUCACUUCCAUUCACCCAGACAGUCUCUUCCAGAAUAUUUCAGAGAUAUCUAGACAUAUACAAGCACAUAUAUAUUCGUACAUUAUUUUUUCUCACAAGGAGUAAUAACAUAUUUGAACAAUUCUGUACAUUGCUUGGAAAAUAAGAUUUUCUUUAAAGAGUGUCCAGCACAUACAGACCUGUUAAUAAAUAUUUUGUCAAAACCACAGUGAAAUACCAUCUCACAUCUGUCAGAAUGACUAUUAUUAAAACGUCAGGCCAGGUGCAGUGGCUCACGCCUGUAAUCCCAGCACUUUGAGAGGCCAAGGUGGGCGGAUCACUUGAGACCAGGAGUUAGAGAGCAGCCUGGGCAACAUGGCUGUAGAAACCACGCCUCUGAAACAAAAUACAAAAAUUAGCCGGGCCUAAUGGCUUGUGUCUGAAGUCCCAGCUACUUGUAAGGCUGAGGUGGGAGGAUCACUUGAGCCCAUGAGGCAGAGUUGCAGUGAGGCAAGAUAGCACCAGUGCACUCCAGCCUGGGGACAGGGUGAGACCCCAUUUCAAAAAAAAAAAAAGGUCAGUAAACAACAGAUGCUGGAGAGGCUAUGGAGAAAAGGUAACAUUUAUACACGGUUUGUGGGAAUGUAAAUUAGUUCAGCUGCUGUGGGAAGUAGUUUGGAGAUUUCUUAAAUAACUUAAAAUAGAACUACCACUUGACCUAGAAAACAAAAUGUUCUACCAAAAAGACACAUGCACUCAUAUGUUCAUUGCAGCAUUAUUCACGAUAACUAAGACAUGGAAUCAACCUAGGUGCCUAUGAACGGUGGACAGGAUAAAGAAAAUGUGGUACAUAUACAUCAUGGAAUACUAUGCAGUCAUAAAAAAGAAUGAAAUCAUGUCCUUUGCAGCAACAUGGAUGCAGCCAGAGGCCAUUAUCCUAAGUGAAUUAAUGCAGGAACAGAAAACCAAAUGCUGCAUGUUCUCACUUAUAAGCGGGAGCUAAACAUUGGGUGAUUUUGGACAUAAAGAUGGCAACAAUAGACAAUGGGGACUACUAGCCGUGGGAGGGAGGGAGUGGGGACAAGGGUUGAGAAAUCAACUGUUGGGUACUAUGCUCAGUACCUGGGUGACAGGAUCAUUUAUAUCCCAAACCUCAGCGUCACACAAUAUACCCAGGUAACAAGCCUGCCUGUGUACCCCCUGAAUAUAAAACAAAUUUUGAAAAAGGAGAAAAAAUAAUAAAUAUUUUGUUUAAAAAAUACUUCACAGCCGGACACAGUGGCUCAUGCCUGUAAUCCCAGCACUUUGGAAAGCAGAGGCGGGCAGAUGACUUGAGCUCAGGAGUUCAAAACCAGCCCGUGGUGAAACCCCAUCUCUAUCAAAAAUACACCCCUGUAGUCCCAGCUACUCAGAAGGCUGGGGUGGGAGAAUCACUUGAGCCUGGGAGGUGGAGGUUGCAGUGAGCCAAGAUCGUGCCACUGCACUCCAGGCUGAGCGACAGAGCAAGACCCUAUCUCAGGAAAAAAAGAAAAAAUAAUAAAUAAAUGAAAAAUACAAAAUAAAUCACAAAGGCAACGUGCAAGAGGGAAAGGGUGGGAGAAGGAAUAUCUGCAUAGUAAUACCGUACCACAGUUACACUCAGAAAGACUUGCCUAGGAAGCCAGGGUUCUAAUCUUGUGUGAAUUCUUCCGGUCUAGGAUAGGAAGCUAUAUGGUAUAGCAAAAAGACCAUAGGGCUUGGAGUCAAACUCACACAGAAUGUGUUCCAUAUUUAUUAGCCCAGCAAUCAAUGAACUGAAAAUUCUCAUAGGCAACCACACAGCCUGGUGCUGAGCACAUGGUAAAUUUUACACAGGAAUGAUAAAAACUUCUGCUCUUUCAUGAAUCUUCUCUACAGUAGUUUGGCUAAAUUUCAACUUGGGUCUUGUUGCAAUAGUCUACAUAUGAUGAAAAAACACCUGGUGGUAGUUUUCCUCUUCUCUGAAAGCAAUGGCUAGCAUUUAUGGAGUAUUACUAUUGCUAGGCACUGUACGAAGCACUGCGCCAAUGUGAUCACAUUUAAUACUCAUCACGACCCUUCAAGGUAGUGACUAUUCUUGCUAUUAUCUUUAGGCCAGAAACUGAAGAGAAACAUAAGAUGACUUGCUCACUGUUCCCUCAAGUAAAUAGACUCUCAUCUGGCUGACCCCAACGUGUCUGCUCCUCACAGUCCUUGCCUGCCUCUUGUCUGCAUCAAAUGGUCUUAUUCUCUGUAGACAUAACCCUUGGACACCCCAGAAGAGAAACGGAGUUAUUACCACCUCAGCUCAGUUCUGGCACACACCCCUAAAGCUUUAGGCAGCUUUUUAAUGCAUGACAACUACAAAUAACAGGACAAGGCAGCCUUUGACCCCACAUGUCAGAGAUCCUGUAUUAUUCUUUACUGCAUUGGCCAGCAGGCAAGAGUUUUUACUGAGGUGCAUUUUCUGGUUUCUCUUACUUCUGUCUCCCAACCAACCUAUCCUGGAGAACAUCCUUGCCUUCUAAUCUCUUGCCAUCACAGCAGGCUUCCUAUAAUUCCUGCAGCAUAAUGCAAAAAGAAAGGAGGGAAAAAAGUGUUGACUGAGAUUUCUGGCAAACAUUAUUUAAGCUGAAGAGGAGCACUGCAGAUUGACUAUUAGACACUACUAGACUAUUAGUGCUAGUAAUGCCAGGAUGCUUUCUUGUCAGCAUUCCAGUUUCAGAUUUUUGUGACUGUUUAAUUACCAACACUCUCCCACAUUGCCAGGAUGUGCCUCUUCAAAACCCUACUGGAAGUUCAGUGUCGAUUACAACCAGCUACAUGCACUUCCUACAUUGUAGAUCUCUAAUAGCUUUCUGUAUUCUAUGGCACUAGCAGAAAUAGUCCAGAUAAUGGCUCUAAAUUUCCCUUUUAAAUCUUGUAUUUUUUUCCCAUGUACCAUGAAAACAGAACUGUUUUCUUUCUGCUGAAGAGUAAUUUUCCUGGUAAUGAUAUUUAAACAGGAGUCUAUUUCAAAAUGUCCACAUUCAUCUCACAUGUUAUCUGAAGAUUCAUUCAUAAUUUUGUUUAGCCAUUUGAAAAAUUGUGGGAAUUACAUAUUUGAUGUCAAUGUUGAAAGAGGAGUUUAAUCCACAGAGGGUUGAGUUUGUCAAGAAAAUAGCAUUGCUACAGAAAUAGGCGGUUCUUUUGUGGAGAAACAAAUUUAAUCCUUAUCCCAAAAAAAAAAUGUAUCCUCUCCAGUCAGCAAUGUCUCUGAGAAUGUCUAGGAAACUGGAGAAGAUAAUCUUAGUGCUAAAAUAAUAUUCAGGUUUUUAAAUGGUAUCUAAGGAUUUCUUCAGAAAUGUAUGUGUACAAAAAUAGAUUUUUCAAAACUGAAUAAACAUAGUUCUUAAACAAUGAUGAGGAAAAUAGUUUUGCUUAUACGGCACCAGCAAAUGGGGAAAAAUUUAUUUCCUGUUGAAUACAUGGGAGAAACAGAAAUCCUCAUUGAGGUGGGAAGGGAGAGAGGCAGUCGUUUCAAUAUAUUGAGCACUGAACACCCAGGCUUACCUCCCACAUGGUUAUCUGUCAGAUUGAUCAGAUUGGUUUGUAACAAGUCAACAGUGAUAACUUUAUGUUUAUGGUGGCAGUGUUCUAAUUUAUUAUCAGUACUAAUGAUAAUUAUCAACUUCAUACAUUUUGCUAAUGAUAUUGAGAAAUUUUCAAAUAGCAACUCUUAAGAAAGCUCUCCUGUCUGGGGAGAUGAAGGAGUUGCCUUAAGGUAAGAAUACAGAUUAGACAGUAUCUUAAAAGUCCUUUCGGCCCUAUGUUACGAUGAGGAAUAUUGUGUAUGGUGGAACACUUCCACGGGCAUAAUUUAAUCUGUCCUUUCUCUGUUGUAGAUACUGCUGCCACCAACUCAUUUCCUUCAAUCCUCUUUUAUUAGGUUGGUGCAAAAUUAAUUAAUUGUGGUUUUUGCCAUUACUUUCAAAAACAAACAAACAAAGAAAGUGGCUUCCAAAGCUGAAAUCUCACAGGAGAUUAGAGCUUUGUACACAACAUUGUGAGCUAAUUUGCAGCUGAAUCUUUAAAACCUCGUGCUUCCUUUCCAUCAAAUUACUCAAAGUUUGGGUUCCCCUAAAAGCAGAGUCUAUUUGAGACAAGGACCUAGGUGCAGGUAGUUGAUUUCGGAGGUGAUCUCAAGAAGUGGAAUGAAGGGCAGAGAGAUUGAUACAGGGAAGAAUGGAGAGUCCUUAAAGAAUGAAUACUGAGCUGGUUACCACUUUGGGCAACUGGGGUGGAAUCUGACUGGGGACAAUUUGAAGAAUUGUUCAGAAUGCACUUAGAAUAAUGAUGCCCCCCACCUCCCAUAGGUUUGAAGGCUGGAGCAUUAUCCAACAACCCCUCACCUCGCCCAUCCUCUUUCCACUUACCUCCUUCUUCCCAGCCUCACAUUAAUUCCUCCAUACUUGGCCAAGUGGGUUCUGCAGUUUUGCAGAAAGUUCUGAAGCAGAGGAGCUGAGGAGCCUUAAGACAGGAAGUCCUCACUGGUUAAAGGAACUGCUCAUCACAUCUGCAGCUAAAAUAAGAUGUGGUUCAAGUCAGGAGUGGUCAAAGGCAUGGGCCAUGGAAUCCCAUGAGCAGCUGCCACAUUUUUAAUUGCUUGUACUCCCCUACCCUGCAUCUCCACCUCCUAGCCUACUUCCCUCCUGUUCACACUCUGCCUUGUGCAUUUCACCCACAGUCUUCCAUGGCCCCUCUAAGUCAGCUUGCCUCUCUCCUCAUCCCCAGCUCCAUCUCCCUCCUGCAUGCCUAGUUCAACGGUGCAAUUCUGCCACCCUGGCUUUUCUUCCUUCCUCUCUAGCUAAAAUCAUCUUUGUUUAGAAGCCUCAUCUUUCUUAUCUGGCUUUCCAUUUCAUUAAAACAACAAAAACAAAUGUAGUUUCCAAAGGUCAAAUGUUACAUUAGAUUAGAGAUUUGUACACAACCUUGUGGGCUAAUUUGCAGCUGAAUCUUUAAAAUCUGGUGCUUCCUUUCCAUCAAACUACUCAACCCUUCUUCCCCACUCCAUGUUCCCUAAAAGGGAAUCUCAACUAAAAAUAGCUUUCAGUGUUUGAAAGCAGUAAUGUGGUGUGGGCUGAGGAGCUCAACUUGUGCAUGCGUGGAGACAACUUUAUUCUGACAGUCUCAGGAGACACAUACCCCUUACCUGGCAGGUGACACAAGAUGAAGGGCUCUGUGUUCUCUUGCAGCACUGAAGGCAUGUAAUGGAACUAAUUAAAGCAGGCAGGCCUGGGCCCAUGGCUCUCACUCAUCUCAAAGCCCAAACUUUGUCAGAGUGUACAAGAGCUGGGACUGGCCAUAUUACCCAUGUGUUGGGCAAGGUCCCCUGAAACAGGGCUCCUUUGCAGAGUACCCAGUUUGAACCUACAGCAAAAAGGCUGGCACACCUCCAAAGCCUUCUGCUCUCUUCCAUAGGUUUCUUCUGUAGCUUCAGAGACCGAAAAGAUCUUGGCAGAGCCUGAAGUAAUCUUUUUCUUUCAUGGAGCUGAGUUUCAGACUCUCUAGCUCUAACUCCAUUAAGCAUGCCUCCCUUGAGUUCCCAACACAGUCUUUGCUUCAAUAGCAUUGCUAAUUGGGAUGUAGUAUAAUUCAUCUGUUCAAAUGUCUGCUGCCUUCCCCACUAGACUGGAAACACCCUGUGGCAAGAGCCACUUCCUAGCAAUAACAAUAGCUGCCGUUUACUGGACAUUUAAUAUGUGCUAGGUAUUGUCCUGGGGUUCUAAACACAUUUCAUGUUCUUUAUGGUAGUCUUGCUAGGCAGAUAUUAUCAUCCCCUUUUGUAAAUCAGAAAAUUUGAGAGAGGUCAAGUAUGCCCAGGGAUAUACAGCUUUUGAAGGACAGAAGAGGAAUUUGGGCCCAGUCGCCUAUCUAUCUGAACCAGUGCACCUAACUGGUGAGCUGUACAGCCCCUUCACUGCUUCAGUAUAUGUGUCUCCUGGCCAAGAAACCAACUAGCAGUGAAUGAAGGGAUAUACAGAGUGGGCUUAGCAAACUCUAGGCUCAUCUCACACAUUUAUUUACUUUGUGCAUUUGGAAAUAAUGCCAAUCACACUCAUCCAUCUACACUGAAGAAAUGCCACGUUUUUUGCCUUCAAAAAAUAAUUUUAAUUGGCUUUUUGUAUAGUUUGUAGCAUUGGCAUAUUUACUUUUAGUCUUUUCUAAGUAUAAAUCGUAUGUAGUAUAUAUGUGUAUAUGUACGUAUGAAUAUGCAAUAUAUAUAUAAUAUGUCAUAUACAGCUCCUUUAAACCUGCUUUGUUCAUAUAGCAACAACAUAACACCAUGAGUAUUCUUCCAAUAAAAGUAUCAUUGCUGCAAUAUAGUCAGAACAAGUGUUGUGAUUAGAUAAUCAGAUUGGAAGGGAAUUUUGAAGUCAUUACACACCUUUAUCUAAACUAAUGGUCUCCAUUGGAACAGAACAGAGGACUCAGAAAUAACACCGCACAUCUACAACCAUCUGAUCUUUGACAAACCUGACAAAAACAAGAAAUGAGGAAAGUAUUCCCUAUUAAAUAAAUGAUGCUGGGAAAACUGUCUAGCCAUAUGUAGAAACCUGAAACCUGAAAGAAAGCCAUAUGUAGAAACCCUUCCUUACACCUUAUACAAAAAUUAAUUCAAGAUGGAUUAAAGACUUAAAUGUUAGACCUAAAACCAUAAAAACUCUAGAAGAAAACCUAGGCAAUACCAUUCAGGACAUAGGCAUGGGCAAGGACUUCAUGUCUAAAACACCAAAAGCAAUGGCAACAAAAGCCAAAAUUGACAAAUGGGAUCUAAUUAAACUAAAGAGCUCCUGCACAGCAAAAGAAACUACUGUCAGAGUGAACAGGUAACCUACAGAAUGGGAGAAAAUUUUUGCAAUCUACUCAUCUGACAAAGGGCUAAUAUCCAGAAUCUACAAAGAACUUAAACAAACUUACAAGAAAAAAACAACCCCAUCAAAAAGUGAGCAACGGAUAUGAACAGACACUUCUCAAAAGAAGACAUUUAUGCAGCCGAAAGACACAUGAAAAAAUGCUCAUCGUCACUGGUCAUCAGAGAAAUGCAAAUCAAAACCACACUGAGAUACCAUCUCACACCAGUUAGAAUGGCAAUCAUUAAAAAGUCAGGAAACAACAGGUGCUGGAGAGGAUGUGGAGAAAUAGGAACACUUUUACACUGUUGAUGGGAGUGUAAACUAGUUCAACCAUUGUGGAAGACAGUGUGGCGAUUCCUCAAGGAUCUAGAGCUAGAAAUAUCAUUUGACCCAGCAAUCCCAUUACUGGGUAUAUACCGAAAGGAUUAUAAAUCAUGCUACUAUAAAGACACAUGUGCACGUAUGUUUAUUGUGGCACUAUUCACAGUUCACUAUUCACUAUUCACAGAACCAACCCAAAUGUCCAGCAAUGAUAGACUGGAUUAAGAAAAUGUGGCACAUAUACACCAUGGAAUACUAUGCAGCCAUAAAAAAGGAUGAGUUCAUGUCCUUUGCAGGGACAUGGAUGAAGCUGGAAACCAUCAUUCUCAGCAAACUAUCACAAGGACAGGAAACCAAACACUGCAUGUUCUCACUCAUAGGUGGGAAUUGAAAAAUGAGAACACUUGGUCACAGGGUGGGGAACAUCACACACUGGGGCAUGUCAUGGGGUGGGGGGCAGGGGGAGGGGAUAGCAUUGGGAGAAAUACCUAAUGUAAAUGACGGGUCGAUGGGUGCAGCAGGCCAGCAUGGCACAUGUAUACCUAUGUAACGAGCCUGCACAUUGUGCACAUGUACCCUAGAACUUAAAGUAUAAUAAAUAAAUAAUUUAAAAAUGAAAAAAAUAAACUAAUGGUCUCAAAGUUAUUUUUAACUAUGACUCAUUUUUUUUCCCUAAGGAAACCUAUAUAAAACAUCAAUAGCUAGCAUAAAUAAAAAAUGGCAUUAUGGUUAUAUUUAUAUGAAUUUAUUUUGUAAGUACAGCUUUGUCACAUUUACUCAUUAAAAAGCCAGCCAAUUAGAGUAGUAAGGCUCAUUCAACUAGGCAGCAAUUUUUAACUGGAAGUUAGGAUAACAGUUGAAGUUUUAUGUAAGCCUCAGUAUCUUGUUUUCAUUGUGUAGGAGUCAGGGGAUCAUGGUCCACACAGGUAUUUGUAACAUCAUUGUUUAACAGAUGCCCCUGCAAUUAGCUAAAUACAUGCCACAGGAGAAGCUUGAUUUCAAGUCUGCACAAAAAUGAGUUAACCUUGUAGCAGCACCCAAACUUUGGUGUUCCAACAUAUCCAAGUUUUAUAUAAGACACAUUUAAAUGCAUGGGUGCCACUUUUUCUUACCAUUUUUUAAAUAGUCAAAAGUAAAUUCUCAUUAAAAAGUGAAAUCUUAACCAAAUAUGUGUAUAAUCCCUUAAAGCAUACUUUAUAGAAGUCUAGGGUUCCAUGACACCCUAGGGUUUUCUGAAAUUCAGCUAGGAAAUCACUGAUUUAGCUUUCCCUAAAAGUCUAACACAUUAAUAAAAGCUGCAAAACAGGGAGGCUACCCAGGCUGUCUCAGGAAUACGCCCAAGUAUUUAAAUCCCCUAAUGAUAGUCAGAAAAUUCCUUCUCAUGCCUGAGUUGAGUUUCCUAAGCUGGUGCCUAAGCUUAGCAUAGUAUAUAGAAGGCUCUUGGAAAAGACUUGUUGACUGACAGAUGGAGGCUCCUGUGGAAGGGUAAGGUAGGUGGUUGGCCACUCUUCUUCUCACCAAAUAAAUAUGAUCUAGUCUCCCACUCACUCCUGACUUGGUACUGUGAUUACUACGAUUAGGCAGCAUCAUUUUCUGAUUAGCCCAACAUCCUGCCAAAACAGUAAUGACUUCUGCAAGUCACCUCUGCAUAGAAAACAUUUGGCUUGAUACAUUUUUACAGUGUGGGUUUGCAAAAGAUACUGAUCAAUGCUCUUCAUAGCACUUAUGUGAAGCUCUAAUACUUCUCGCCAUAAGUCAGUAUAGGAUAGAGGUCUUUGCACUGGGUCAGGCAGAAAGGGAAAGCCGGUAAUUUGAGUUGUCCACUUGAGCCAGUAAUUGAAUGUUCAAUAGUUGUCUGGGGAGUUGGAUUCAUUUGCGGCAGAUGAAAACAGGAGAUGGUAGGCAGAUCUGAGGCAUACGGAAAAGACUCAGUUGUCAGAAUAGGGUCAUAGGGCCAGAGAGUCAGGAGGACUUGAUACUCACUGGCCAUGCAUUGUGCUGAAGGCACGUAAAUCUAUCCUUUCUGGCCCACAUUAGACUCGUGUGAGAACAGGGAGGAUACUGGGCCUUCAGACAGGGGCCAAGGAGGGAGCUGGAGGGAGAGGACAGCCUCACCAUCUGGGGUGCCAGGGAAGGUCUAAUAUGCUCAGGAUUGGGCUGCCCCAAAGUGCAUAUGGGAAUUUUCUCCACAGUCUUAUGACAUAGGUUAUUUAUGUUAGAUAGUGAGCUUUUCCUCAUCUUGCUGCCAGCCCCUUUGCCCUAACCCAUGUAUUUACUGCAUCACCGAUCACUGGAAGGUUUGAUGGCUGCCCAGGCAUUUAAGAGAAUUUGGAAGCUGUGUUCUAAUCCUGGAAGGAAGUAUAAAAUUUUAAUUGAACUAUGUAGACAGUUUGAAGUCAUUUUACAAAUAGGAAGGCGAGGCUUUUUGAGCCUUGCCCGCCAUUCAUGUAAGUGGAAUUCUUCAUGAGAGACAGAAAGGUUAGGUUCAUUCCAUGGCAUGAGGACUGAUGUGAGCAAAGGUGAAAUCUGGGAGAGUAAGUGUAGUGAGUAGAGCAGACACCAGCACACCAUGUUGGCUUUUCUGUCUUCCCUGUCUCUCUUUCCCUACAUCCUGGUUUGUGCUUCCUGGAUUCACCUCUCAAAUAAACCACCUGCACUCAAGUCCUUGUCUCGGGUUCUGCUUUUGGGGGAAGCCAAACUAAGACAGCGAGUUCAACCUUCUUCAGCUGAACGUCAUAGCUUUGGGGGAGAAUUACAUGGAGCAAUGAUGGAUGGCAAGGAUACCCAUCAGAUCAGCCAUCUCAACCUGGGCAAGCUAGACAGACUCAGACCAACCACUUGUCCAUGCUUCUAAGAAACUAGGAGUGUGCCUGAAUAGAAAAUGGAGUUUAUUCAAUAGUAUUAACUCACUCAAUCACAAGGUCCCACAACAGGUCAUCUGCAAGAUGAGGAGCAAGGAAGCCAGUCCAAGUCCCAAAGCUGAAGAACUUGAAGUCCAAUGUUUUAGGGCAGGAAGCAUCCAGCACUGGAGAUAGAUGUAAGCUGGGAGGCUAAGCCAGUCUGACCUUUUCAUGUUUCUCUGGCUGCUUUAUAUUCUAGCGACACUGGCAGCUGAUUAGAUGGUGCCCACCCAGAUUAAGGGUGGGUCUGCCUUUCUCAGCCCACUGACUCAAAUGUUAACCUUCUUUGGCAACACCCUCACAGACACACCCAGGAUCAAUACUUUGCAUCCUUCAAUCCCAUCAAAUUGACACUCAAUAUUAGCCAUCACACCAGGUUAAUGAGUUCCUUCUCUAUUCAGUCCCUCUGCUGUUGGACAAAACUUUUACCUUGCUGUUUGCUUCUGAGAUAGUGAGAGUUUGGGUUUGAAGCAGAUGCUGAUCAGUGACCUUCACCACACUUUCCUAGUCACAGUAUCACAGUCGCUCUGAACCUACCAAGUCAAGCCAAGAGACAGCAUCUUUCCUUUUUGUGUGUGUGUAGAAUUGACACUCUUGCCUUAGUGUUUGUAACAUUUGGAGUUUAUAGGGAACCACAGAGAGAAAACAUACUCUAUUUUGAUUUCUUCCUGGUAGUUUUACUUUCUCUAAACUUUUUGUUUGGUUCAGUAGCAGCAAAGUACCUCCUACUCAGCCCCCCAACACCCUCACUUCCCACCUGUCAAACCACCCCAAGUCCUUAUUUCCCUUCCCCUUCCGGAAGCAGUUAGGAGGAAGGGGGUGUGGUCAGAACCAGACCCACUUCUAAUAUUUUCAGAGCCCAAAACAUGAGUAUGAAUGGAGGUCCAUAUACUAUAGGUCUAAAUAUGUUAACAUUAUCAAUCAAAUUUACAAACAUGUAAUAAAAUAUAUUUGGCCACCUUCUUUGCCAGAGCCUAAUGAAGAGAAGUUGGUAGGAGACCAGGGGGAGAAGUGGCCCUGGCCUGAAGCCCAUCCCCUCUUCUCUUCCCACCCCUGGUUCCAUAGGCACUGAAACAUGAAUCCUGCUCACAUGUGUGGACAGCUCAGCUCGCAAGCUCUAUCCUUGCCCUGCCCCUGUAAACGUGGCUCCCUUUGCCCUCCUGGAGCCUAGAGGUUUUCUGAAAGCAGUGGCACAGUGACCCUCAGGAGGACAGACAGGGAGGACAGAUGCUCACAGGCCCUGGGCCCAAGCUUGGAGCCUUUGCAUCCUUCAAUCCAAUCAAAUCAACACUCAGUAUUAGCCAUCACACCAAUUAGACAAUUCCAGGGUGCAGAAGGGGAAGGUAGGCUCCAAUUGGGCCUAUCCCCUUGGCCUGGAGGACUCUCCCUUACAUGGGAAGAAAGACAGCCAGCAAAAUACCAGAGCACAGCCCUCUAAGAAUAAAAGGGACAAAGGCCUCCCUAGCCUGGUUCAAAGGGCAGGACUGCUCAGGGCUGAUGGACGAGACACAUCUAGUACCUCUUUUCUUCCAUCUCAAGCCUGUCCGUGGCACUACUGUAUGGCUCUUUUUUGAGGAAAGAGGGCUUUGUUUUUCAUUUUAUUUUUGCUUUCUCUAAACAUGCCCUGCAGAUCCUUCCUUUAACAGUGUGGGGACUGAACAAACAGCUUCUGACCCUGGCCCUGUUUCUGUAUCUGGAGCAACACAAUAGAACAUCUGCCUUGACCUGGACUGCCUUCCACUCUGCACAUCAUUCUUGGCCAUUUCCCAUCUGUGCCAGGAGAGGGGUGAAGCUGUCAAUACAAAUCAACUGUAUGGACUCCUGCCCGUUCUCUGCUGCAAGGGCUGGAAGCUUCCCCGUGAUGAAGAAAGGCAACCUCAGUGCUUCGGAGGCUUAGCACUAUUUGCCCACCCCAGAAUCCAUCAGGAAAACUGAAAUUAUAGAGUACAUUGUGGCAAAGUUGGAACAAAACAACAACUGAUGAGCAUGAGUUUUUGUCACAUUCCCUAGGCCACUGGAGUCACCCAAGCAUUCCUUCAGCUUGGGCUGUCUCUCUGCAAAGGGCUCUGUGUUCUAGCUCUCGACUCGUGCAGUGGGAGAAGAGUCUUAAUAUACAGCGGCCCAUUUGAGUGGUGUUCAAUGGGCUGCACCACAGACUCUGGGAUAGCAGGUGAUAUUUCAUAUCGCCUAGGCAGCACUGAAAGGAACAUUAAGCUGCAUUUCCAUUAUCAGUGAGGUCCGUAGUGGCCUGAGGAUCAGAAUCCGAGCAUUCUAAUCAGUCUGCCUAAUAUUUUCCUGGGCAGCCUCCUACAAGCCUAUGAUUAGUUUGCAGAGGAAGUCUGAACCACCUUUCUUAAGGGAAAAGUGAUCUGCAAGAAUGCCUGGAGCGUGAUGAGCCAAGGAGAGAUUCAGUGACAAGUUAAAGGGCCUUGUGCUAUGAAUAAAAGGAUCACUUCUGGGGAACUUAAGGAUUUCUGCAGAGAGGAGUAGCUCAUUUGGCUGGAGUACUAAAAUCCAUGAAAACUGCUGAAAGACCAGUAAGGAAAUUUCUGUUCAGAGAGACCAAGAUUCUAGUCUUAGCCUUUGCCCUCAUGUGAAUUAUUUUGCAGAUCCCAAACCACCUAAUACUGCUAGAAAAAAAUCUUCUAUUUCCCAUGUUAAAUCAUGAAAUUUGAUAAGUUUAGGUUGAAGAGAAAAGCAAGGACAUCUAAACUGAAUACCAGUGUGAUGCUUAGUUCCUCUGCAAGGCACCGCCAAGCUGACUUUCAUCCUCCAUGGGACACCUUCAAGGAGAGGGAACUCACUGCUUGUAGCUGUGGACAUUUCUGAUUACUAAAAGUUCUCAUUAGUAUCAAAAUCCUGAACAUCAAGUGUCUAAAAACAGAGACCUAUAUCUUAACCUCUAGCAUCCUCCCCAAGUGAGGGAGGAUGUGUAUUUGCAAAGUCAGCUGCUGGAAUAGAUGUCAUACUGCAAGAAUUGACCUUCACAAAAAUAGAAUAUUUUGCCUAGAAUGUUGGCUAAGGAAUCAGUUUUGUUUUGUGUGUGGCUGUGUGAAGAAAAUAACAUUUUAUUAUGUGAAUAGUUUCAAUAGGGAUAAAAAUUUCAGGUUACUAAUGCAUGAAAACACUUUGAAGUAUAUUUCAAGUGAAAAUUGUCAAUAAUCAUGAUAAUAAUAAUGGAACUCUGCACAGAAUAUAUUCUUCUCAGGCAGUCAGUCUGUGGCAGACAUGCUUGAGGUAGAAAAAUUUAUGCCUGCAUUCAUUCAUUCAUUUAUGUAUACAUUCAUCAAAUAUUUAUUGACUACCAACUAUGGGCUCAGCCCUAAAACGACCGGGAUGAAAGACUGGAGUUUCUUCCCCUAAGAAGGAGCCCAGAAUCUAGUGGGAAAGAUGAUGAUGUAAACCACUCAUUAUGACACUGAGAAAAGAUGCCAAGGGUUCUGUGGAACUCAGGAUGUGCACCUGGAUUAACUCAGAAGGAAUUUCCCAGGGUAAAUGGGACAUCGCAGAUUGAUAUCAGCUGGUUCUCUUCAUUGCCUCCUCCAGAAUCUCCAGUUCCCUGAUGAGUUAGAGUGAAGUACAUGCGAGAAGCCACGCCCUAUGUGAAGAAAGGAUCCCCAGUAUCCGAGAUUGGGUGGGAAACACCUCCGCCUGAAUCCCCUCGGUUAGGGGGCAGCACCUCAGACCCCCCGUCAUCGCAGUCCUUCUCCUUCCACAGAGACCGGAAAAGCAUCCCCCUCAAAAUGUGCUACGUCACUCGGAGUAUGGCCUUGGCCGACCCUGAGAACAGGCAGCUUGAAAUCCACUCUCCAGAUGCUAAGCACACGGUGAUCCUAAGGAGCAAGGACUCAGCCACGGCCCAGGCAUGGUUCAGUGCCAUCCAUUCCAACGUUAAUGACCUGCUGACCCGAGUGAUUGCUGAGGUCAGAGAGCAGCUGGGGAAAACAGGCAUUGCUGGGAGCCGAGAGAUUAGGCAUCUUGGCUGGCUUGCAGAAAAGGUGCCAGGGGAGAGCAAGAAACAGUGGAAACCAGCCCUGGUUGUGCUGACUGAGAAAGACCUUUUAAUCUAUGACAGCAUGCCACGGAGGAAGGAAGCCUGGUUCAGCCCAGUUCACACAUACCCUCUUCUUGCCACCAGGCUGGUCCAUUCAGGUCCAGGAAAGGGAUCACCCCAGGCUGGUGUGGAUCUGUCCUUUGCAACGCGAACUGGUACCAGGCAAGGGAUUGAAACACAUCUCUUCAGAGCAGAGACCAGCAGGGACCUCUCCCACUGGACAAGGAGCAUAGUACAGGGUUGCCACAAUUCUGCUGAACUCAUUGCUGAAAUCAGCACUGCUUGCACCUACAAAAACCAGGAGUGCCGUUUGACCAUACAUUAUGAGAAUGGAUUUUCUAUUACCACUGAACCACAGGAGGGUGCCUUUCCCAAGACCAUCAUACAGUCUCCUUAUGAAAAGCUCAAAAUGUCUUCAGAUGAUGGAAUCAGGAUGCUGUAUUUAGAUUUUGGAGGCAAAGAUGGAGAGAUUCAACUGGACCUUCAUUCCUGCCCCAAGCCAAUUGUUUUCAUCAUUCAUUCCUUCCUGUCAGCUAAGAUUACAAGACUGGGCUUGGUGGCCUGAAGACAGGGGUGACUUGCCUUUGAGAAAAGAAGGGCUGCAAUGCCACCAGAGAACGUGAUGUCAGACACCAUCUGUAGUGAGCAGCGCACCAGAUGUAGCGUGCUACAGUCAGCUUUAGCUCUCAAGAGUCGUAUGUAACUGUCCCAGACUCCUCUGUCAGUUUCAGCAACUACAAGGGAUACCCUGCGAAAGUACCAUGAGAAAUAUCAGAGUAAAACUUUCUAGAACAGUACAAGGUUAAAGAGGUGAGGUGACGGGAAAUACACAGCAUAGCUUUGAAAUAAUGACAACCAAGGACAUGACCAUUAGAACAGCAUGUGCAGAUCUUAAUCAUCCCAGUUCCUAGGCAACUUGUUCACCAGGUACGCAAGGGCCGAAUAGUUGAGAAAUGGACAUUCUUACCUACUCCUCCUAGCCCCCUAUCCCCAGUAACAGUGAUCCCUUUUCUUAUUGUGAUUUAUUUCCUAAUUCUUGCUGAGUUGACUUUCCCUUGUAGGAAAAGAAAAAUAUUUCAAAUAGAAACCCACCUUUUAUUUAAGUAUGAAGCAGCUGUUACUUUUUAAAAAAUGAAUUAUCUUUCAAUGGUGUAGAAUGAUUCCAAAGUGUCUCCAUUAGCAUAUACUGAGCAGGAAUUAAAUAAAGCAUCAGAUACUGAUCUGAGCUGUAAGCUGGUAGAAUCUGAGCCAAAGUAGACUGCUUAAAUUGAUAAGCUUUGCUAAAGAGUUGUAUGCACAAAGGAUGAUUAAUUCUGGGACUAUACUCACACCAAGGUCUGCUGUCUUAUAGCCAAGAAUUACAGCUUUAUUUAUAGAGAGUGAAUUAUGGGUAUUUUUUCAGAAAAUAUUGUCAUCUGAUAUACACAUAAAACAACUCACAUUGUUGGAGUUAACUAAUUAUCCCCAUUUCAUGGUUUUCAGUGGCAACUUACUGACCCUUGUUUUUGCCUGUGCUUGUAUGCAUGCAUUUUCAAGCAAGUAAUAAAGCAGCCUCAUUUAAUUCUGGAUAAUGCUGGGUUUUACAUAUAGACUGAAUGCUAUAAUCAAAUCUAUUGACAGUAUCUGCAGUUCUUUCAGAAUUCCAGGGAAAUAAUAUAACGACCUGAUAUCUUUCUACAGGAAUAUUUUCAGACAUUAUAUAGCACAUUACUGAUUUAAUGCUUUUACUUUUAUCUUUCAAAACAAAUUCACUAAAAAUAACACCUAUUGAUUUUGAAGUCACUUUUCUCAAACCUUGAAAAUGAGCUCUAGGAUCUCUAUAAACAUUUCUAACACUUUUCCUGUAGUUUACAUAGACAGACAUCUGUUGUUAGACCUGUGUGUUUUUAAAGAAUCAUAUGUUAACAAAUACCCAUGCAAAGAGCUUCAAAAAGUGAAACCGUGUUAAAGGAACACAAUUUUUCUCACUCAGACAUAUUUGUUUAUUGAAUUGCAAAGUUUUAUUUUAAAUCAGCAUUUCCCCAAAGAAUAUAUCAUAUGACGCUAGUUCCAAGGGGCUUGACUGAGUGGUGUUUUGCUGGGGGGAGACAGGGGUUUGUUAAUACACUUUACUAAAUACUGAGCUGAAAAAUGUUAAAUAGAUUUCACGAUUGCCUCCUUGAAGAUUUUAAAGUUCAUUGUGGUUCUUCAAGGCGAAAUCCGGUGAACCAUUCCUCACACUUACCUACAGGACUCUUUUCUAAUGGAGCAUCUUGUGAAGCUAGUGGGUUUUUUUGUUGUUGUUAUUUGUUUUUUUUUUUUAAUGCUUUAGAAAACACAGCUUUAGGAUAUUGACUUUUUGUUUAUUUCUAUUUUCAAAUGCUGAAAAGUCAAGUCCCAGUUUGAAUACCAUAGAAAAGCUUUGAUGCAUUUGUAAAUUAUAUUGCACUCUUUCACUAUAUAUUUUCAAAAUCACUGGAAUGUUGUUAUACAAGAGAAUUAUAAUUGUGUAUUGUAAAUAACAUAUUAAAAUACAUAUAUUAAUGCCAAUAGUUAAAUUCAACAAUAUGUAAUCUAAGGUGCUCGGUUCUACAUGAAGUAUGAGUUAACUGCUCAUAAUUAAGUUGCCAAGAUUCUAUUAUAUAUUUAUAGACAAAUUAAAAUGAUCAUAAUUACAAAUAUGAUUUCUUUAUCACUUAAGCUUUGGGCUGAUUAAUAUCUGUGUGGGGGUCAAUGGAAACUACAUUCUCUACAUUUAUAAACAUUUAAUUUAAUUAUUUAUAUUUUAGGAAAAUAUAUUUGAAUAAAAUUAAUGCAUUUUCUAGAGUAAAUUAAAAUGUUAUUAGCAAGAAAUAGAAAAUUUGACUAAGAUAAUUGUGUAUAUGAAUCAUUUUUCCCCCAAGUUAAAAUGUAUCAUAAUAGAGAGGCUCUAAUGAAUCAAUUUCCAAUACUCAUUUCUUUCUUAUUUUGAAUUCAAGUUACAAUGACUUUACACUGUAGAUUUUAAUCUUGUCUGAUGUGUGCUGGUGUGUAUGACACAAACUCAUAAGUCUGGAUCAUGCUUGGGUACAGUCAAUGAAUCAACCGAGUCACUUUGAGGAAUUUGUUUUUGUCCAAUUUGCUCUGUGCUCAAUCCCAUGAAUUAUUAAAUUUACAAUGUUUGUCCCCAAAUGAAAACCAAUAUAAAUGAAUGAUGUUUUAAUCUGUACUUUAUGGGAAGUUGCCUAUUUGUCAGUAGAUGUGGUUAAGUGAGUCCUCUGGUGCAGUGACAUCCUUUUAAGCCAUCUCAUAGGGAUUUAAAGAAGGCCAAUAGGAAUAUAGAUAUUGGUUUUUCUUUCUCUGACUUGAACUAAGUAGGAGAAACCAAACCAUAAACCUAUUACAAACUACCCAGGCAGAGGCAUUUACUUAAUUCAUCAACUAGUGCAAUUAAAACCCUGAAAACACAUGAUCCUUGUUGACUCUGCUUGGUUGAAGCAGGAAAGAAUGGUCUUGAUGGUCAGAAAGUUUUAAAAUUAAUGGGCAGGGCCUUUCUGGACCCUGUUUUCCAAACACGUUAGAUAUUCCGUCUUGAGGGGAUUGGAGUAGGCUACAGUGAGGGGGUAAUUUUUGGAUGUAUCUGGACUUUUAAAAAAUGUGCCUAUAUUUAUAGCACCAUGAAUAUUAUGUAAAAUUUAUAUAUGAAUUAAAUAAAUAUUCACCUCUGA